GCAGAAUAGAACAUGCCGGUGGACAUGUGAACAUGCGGGAGAACCCAUGUCGGGCGUUCAUUGUUCAUCUGCGUCUACAGGAGGGGGCUACAGUCAAUGCUCCCACUGUCUAGAGUGUUAAAAUGAAACAAUUUUCUCUUUAUUAAGUACCUCCUUGAGACUCCCUCUGCUGGACACUCCCGGUGAGUUGAGAGAAGGAACUUGGCAUUGAAUUCAGAACUAUAGUAAACGGCUGGUUUCCCUGUUACUAGGGACCGGGUAUGUGAGUUGGGGUGUAUUUUGUCAACUUUGUGGAAAGCCAUCUUGGGAACUGCACUGUUCUCCUCCUGCUCCUUUCAUUUUAAAUCCAUAUGGAAGGUAGGCCAUGCCCCCGAGGCUGAGACUUGGCUCUCCCCGUUCCUGCUACAUUGUUCUUCCAGUUCCUUACGCCAGAUAAAGAACUGCAGGUGUGUAGGGUGUUACGGUUUAAGAAUAAUCAUGGAUCUCAAAAGUCUCAUGAACUGUUUUUAUUUGCCAGCCUUCCUUCCCUGUCUCAGGUGACCUCCGCGGUGGCCUCUUUCAGCCCUCAGUUUCCCUCCAUCUUGUCCGUGUGCCCUCUUCAUUGUUCCUGCGCUGUGCACCCUUUUAUUCCGGAUGUUUAUCUGUGCACCUUUAUAAUUAUUUUUCUAAUCUUCCUCCCCAUCCCACCUCAACUGGCCCACAUCAGUCUGCCAAAAGCCCAGAUCUGGGUGUUUUUGAAAGAGAUUGUUGGACAUGCUCUAAAACAGACAGGUGACUUCUAGAAUCAAGGAUUAGGUUGCUAGGACCCGCAUUCACUCACUGUGAUGAGUGUGCCAAGACUCUGAUGACCUCCUUUCUCCUGCCGUGGUGACAUCCUCUGGGUUCAGGAAACCUGAUUUUUCCCCUGUCUCAAUCAGAGCACAUGGACUCCCUGUGUGCAUGCUAAACGAGCAGAGCUUUUCCUGUAGAUUUCUAUAAGAAGAGGGAUUCCUUGUGGGUUUUGAGCUCCUAAAGAGUGUGCAUGAUUCUUCUCAGGAAAAGUAUAACGACACGAGAGGGAAUUGUUUCAAUGGGGUGCUGCUGCACCAAGUUGGAAUACCAGGUGAAGGCCCAGAUACAUUAAUGGAGCGUUCUGAACCGCCAGAGAUUUAGACAGAAAUGCUGUUUUUGAAACAAGGGGUAUUUGAUAAUACCAAUUAAUGGGUGGCAAAGAGAAUCAGUCUUCCAGGGCUUGCUUGAAGGAUAGGUUUAUAAAUAGCAUGUUAGUUUUUGGUGGUUUGGAACUGAACUUCUUAUAAAAAGGUUUAUUUUCUUUAGAAGGUUAAACAUUUGCCUUGUGAUUGUAUUUCCUCCAUCAACUUGCUUUGCGAGGCUUUUUCAAUAUCUAGUGCAAAGGCCAACCACCAAGGUCUCUAUUAUGGGUUCUGAAUGAGAGGAGCCUAAAUUCCAAGUUAUUUAUGUUUUCCUCUCCCUGAGAUAUGCUGUGUUGAUUACUAUUGGCUUAUGUAAAGGAACACUUCACAGACUUCCAAAAACUGUCUGCUGCAAUUCAUCAUCAGAUGGACCUGAAGAUGCCUAUCUACCAAGCUGUCUACCAAGAAAUGAGAUUCUGAAUCAUCUUGGGUUAGCAGAGUUUGAUGACACAUGCCCUAAAAUAUCUGUUCCUGUGUUUAGGUUUUAUAUUUUAAAAAUGAGUAAGUAUAAAUGUUGCUUUUCUUCUCGCCACAUUUGAGUAGUGAGUAAGGUGCCUUAAUUUUAUCCUUGAUUUCAGACAAUGUGCUAUGAUACUUGAAUCAGAGAAACCUGAGUUUGAAUCUAGUGAUACGACUUUGGGCUUUAUUGGACUGUGCAGGAACUCCAUUAGAAACUAGUGCACGUAAAGUCCCUGGCUGUAGUAGGCAUCUUCUCAGAGUGUGUUAAAUCCCUCUAUCUUCUGAGAUGCUUACAGACAUGAUGACUCCAGGGAAAGAAUAACCCACAAAUAGUUUCGAAAACCAAUAAUAGCAACAUUUCAAUUAUUAAUCUCCUGCGAUUCCCUUUCCAGUUUGGGCACCAGCAACAAUAAACCCCCUAUAGCCAUAGAAGAAAGAACCUUCUUUUUACUCCCUCUGUGACCUUUCCAGAUUCUUUAUUUGCAUUGAGCUUCUGCUGGUUUCAGGUAGAGAAUUUCUCUUCUAUAGUGGCACUUUCUGUGCUACUUGAAAAAUGUGGAAAUAAACUGCUGGGGCAGAGUUUCAGGGGCUGCAGCUGUGCCUCUUGGAAAGUAUCCCCAAGUAUGAAAGAUAACCUUUGCCGUUAACCAAGAUCCAUUCCUAAACAAGGCAGCAGGCUGGGCAAGGGAGCACCCAGAGGUGGUUCACCAAGAGCCUCCUCCAAGGGGAGGCUCCUCGCCCACCACAAGCCAGGGUCUGCCUCACCAUGCAUUAAACAUCAUUUUCCUACAAAAGACAAUUUGGUGCUUUCUGUAAGUUACAGGGGCUCAGAUUCUUUGUAUUUUAUGUUUUAUAUUUCUUCAUCUCUCUCUCUCUCCCUUCCUCCCAUAGAGACCAGUCUUGGGGAACCACCUUUGAGGUUUGUGUGGAGCAAAGUAGUGAUGAUCAAGAGGGUGUGAUAUGUGAGCAUUUCUUAUUGUUCUCUGAACGUGUAAUUCGCCUGUGCUUUCUGGUAGUCUUAUUGAUGACAAUUCAAGGACUUUGGGUUGGUGUCAAAGACGGGCUUCAGAAUAAUGGCAGUAGACUUUAUAUAACCACCGAUGGGAUGUGAACUUGAAAGGCCCAAACUCGCAAGAGUUCCAUUUCAUAUAGCUAUUCUCUUUUGGGGGAAAAAAGAAAAGAAAAACCUACAGUAUAGGCAGAUCUUUAUUUUUCCUAUAAAAGAAACCCAGAUGCUUGAGGGUCACGGUGAUCACUGUGACUUAGGCCAUAUUGACUUUGUGCUGUGCACCGCCCUGCGCCCUUCACCCACAUGAACUCAAAUGUUCCACCUCUUGACAGACGAGGGCCCAUCUUUAACGCAUUCAUUCAGCAAACAUUUAUGCAGGACCUGCUGUGUGUCAGGCCCUGUGGCAGGUUCUGGGUUUGUCGAAAUGACAAAAUCUUAAUCCCUGUCCCUGACUUUACAGGGUGGGGGAAGUGAAAGAAGCAUAGACUCACUAGACCAUGGGUCUGAUUCAAGAUGGAAUUUUUUCUUCUCCUUUUUUUUUUUAGUGGCAGUUCAUACUUCUAACAUGCCUAUGCUUUCUUCAGCUAGAAUGGGAAGACUUGGGUAGGCACAGUGGCUCACACCUGUAAUCCCAGCACUUUGGAAGGCUGAGGCGGGUGGAUCAGGAGUUCGAGACCAACCUGGCUAACAUGGCGAAACCCCAUCUCUACUAAAAAUACAAAAAAAAAAAAAAAUAGCUGGGCGUGGUGGUGGUGCCUGUAAUCCCAGCUACUUGGGAGGCUGAGGCAGGAGAAUUGCUUGAACCCAGGAGGCGGAGGUUGCAGUCAGCUGAGAUUGUGCCAUUGCACUCCAGCCUGGGCAAUGGAGCGAGAGUCUUUCUCAAUAAAUAAAUAAAGAGUGGGAAGACCCCAUUUUCCUAUCUCUCUUGAAGUGUUUUCUUUACGUAGACUCAAAAAAGUGUUUCUGAGUGUAGAAAAUACUCAUUACAAGCUUUCUUAGAAAUGUCCAUAAAUAUUACUGUCUGUAACUUGCAGAAGAUCCUGUCUUCUUCUAUUUGUUACUUAAAUUUUAUAUCCUUGCCAAUGCAAAUACGUUUCUUAUUUGCACAAGUUCUCAGAGACUUUCGUUUCUGAUAUUUGGUGUGUCGUAGGCUUUGUUGCGAGUGGACUCUUGCAUCAUAUGUGGCUGUUGGAGAAUUGAUUCCCAGCCUUUUCGCCUGGCUGAGACCUUGUAUUCCAGGUAGUUGUGUGGCACUUGGUGGUGGGGAUAUAGAUCGGGCUGUCACUCCGAAGCAUUCAGUGGCUACUUACCCAGAGCAGAUCAUUCAGGGAAUUGUGGAAAAAGAAAAGCCUGACCUAGCUUCAGGGGCAUAGAGCCCCAGAGCAGAAGACCUUGACACAGAUAUAGUUCACCCCCGUCUUCAGGAAGGUGAAUGUCUGUGACUUGAAAUUGUCAGUUCAUUAUUUAUUUAAUUAUUUUUUCCAGGAAAGGGCAGUUGGAACUCCCUGAGUGACCAAUUCCAGUAUUCUAUUAACCUGAUUGUCAAGAAAUUCCUGGGCCUGGCUGAAAUCUCGCCUGCUGUCAUUCAAACUUGUUUUCUUUUACUCAAUUCCUUUCUCUAAAACCUUUCAUAUACUUAAAGAUAAUAACUGGGUCUCUUUAGCUUUUUCCUCACAGAGCCGGUUUUGUGUCACUGAAAGCAUCUCCUUUCUCUCUUCUGAACUCUCUCUAGUUUCUCCCUAUUUAAAAAAAUGGUGGCAGUUAAAACUGAAUACAGCUCUUUAAUAAUGUUCUCAUUAGUACCGCAUAUAAGAGAAAAACGACUUCAGGGUUCUUGCAUCAUCGUGAACCCCUGGAGGGCAGGAACCAUGUCUGAUUCAUCUUUGUCCCCUACAAUAGCCGUGCAGUUCCUUAAACCUAGUAGGCGCUUCAUAAAUAUUUCUGGAAUUGACUGUUCCUUUUAAUGCAUCUAAGUUAUAACUUACGCAGCCCUGGAUUGGUGACUCAUCUGUAGCUCGCAUUCAUUUCGGCCGUCUUUAUUUUUCUUGUACUUGUAUCUGGCAUCCCUCACCCCAACAAAGCCACCUUCUGCUUGACUCCACUGAUCACUUUGCAUUUCACCCCUCAACUUCCAACUCUUUAGAAUCUUGCUUAAUUAUCUCCCGUAGAUCUGACAAACAGAAUGCAGAGGCCAUAAGUAUAAAAACUUGAACUACACUUGAAAGAAGAGCAAGCACACAGAAGAAUCUUGAUGAUUCAGAGCAGUGUCAGGUCAUCCUCAUUUAGAAGGGACCGUUUGUCAAAUUCGUUAUAGAUUCUGAGUCAGCUAAAGCCAUACCUGUUUUACUAGGUUCUCCAAGGUGAGUGAGCUAGGUGUUUAUGAGAGUGGUUACAAGUCAGACUUUCAGAGGGUAGUCCUCCCUCUCUUUGGUUUAAAGCCAAUGGAAAAGGCAAAAGAUGUAAUGAACGACAUCACUGCAGGUUGUGUUUUUUCUGACAGAUAUCUUUGCCCUUAGAAAGCAAGCUAGUAAAAUCAUUGCCAAAAAAGAAAAGGCAGAAAACCUUUGAAACUCCAAAAUAUCUUUGUGGUUUUAUAGCUACUUAUUUCUGAAUACAGCAUUGAACAAAUUUGUAAUGUUUUUGACAGUAGUCUGUUUUAACAAUUCUUGCCUAAGUACUUUUGCCUUAGUAGGUUCUGAUCAAUUAAAUGCCACUGUGUUUAAGCAGAAUUAAGAUUGAUCAAUUCUUCUGCAUGUGUUAAUGCUGUCGACUCUAUAAAAACCUUUGUCACAAAAAGAAUGCAGCCUAAUAUGUGAGUGGACAAGGGUAUUUUUCCUCCAGGUGGUUCUGUCCAUCCGCAGUGAGAGAUCACCAUAGAACCUUCCAUGACAUUGACUACGAAAGCACUUCUGGCUUCACACAGUCACAGAUUUGCAUCUUGAAGAACAAAGGGUUUGUUUGUGUAUUUUUACCAUUUUCCUUCACACUAAUAUUUCCCUGUUGAUUCAACCUAUGGAAUCGUUAUUCCCAAGUAAAAUCAUUCGUCCAAGGGCUUAUGAUAAGAAGCCAGCUCUAUACAAUAUAGAACUUAUAGUUUCAUAGCAUUAAGGAAGCAAAUUUUAAUGGUGUUUGUGCCUGGAUUUCUGUUAAAAGUCACAGGGUUAUAAUGCCGAGGUUGUGAGUAUUAAAUUAAAAAAUUUUAAAAAGUCACAGGGCAGGGAGAUUUGGAAAACUCCAGCUUAUUGCCGAUUGUGGAAAUGUGUUCUUUUAAAAUUUGUUUAUUUUGUAUCUAAUGAAAGAUUUAUAGGGCUCUGACAAAAACCAGCAUGUACGUUUUUGAAACUGUACAGAAAGACAGCAAGUUACACCUUCCUGAAUUCUGUGUCACGGCAUCUACUCACCAGAAUCUGAGCGGAUAGCAGGGACUUCUGGAGGAUAGUAAGUGUCAGGGGAACUCGUGACAGGGAGAAGGAGCACCAAGAGAGAAUGCACACGUGCUUUCGGCCUUUUCCCCUGAACCACUCACCUCUGCAGCUCCAGCACAGUGUCAUUACUAUUAUUCAUUAAGUGUGACCUGUACCAUCAGGAAAAGAUUCAUCAGUUUCAUUAUGUUCUGUUAACUGAGCCUGGGAGGUUCUCUAAUGUAUUACAGAAAUGCUUCCACUAGUCAGUGGUUAAAGAAAUUCUUUCAUUUGCUUGUUACAGUGAUGUACUCCAAAGAGGAUUUAAGGCUGCUUAAAUGGUUAAGUUUCUGGUAGAGAGGGAAAUUAAUUUAUGUAGAUCAAUUUUGUGGAUAGCUUCUUUCCAAGGAUGUCGGAUAAAUGAGGUAUUCCUAUAGAAAGAGACAACAGCAAUAGGCAAAGCUCUGGUGUUGGCUUAACAAGGUGAAUAAGCAGAGUGCAUAAUGGAAUUCAUUUGCAAAGUAAUUUUUGCUUGGCUGGAGUGGUAAGCACAAAAUAGACUAGCAGAUGAGAAUGGUAAGUGUUUGGGAUCAGUUGUUAAAAGGUUUAAAAGGGGUUCUAAUUCAAGUGACAUUUUGUGGUGUGGAGAAGGGGACCGAUAUUAUCAGAAUGAUACUUGAACAAGGUAAUUUUUACUGGCCUGGGUAUAAUAGAAGGAACCAGACAGCCAGGGGUGGGCCAUGCUGGUAGGCCUUGUGGUGCGGUGGAAGGCACUGCGGCCGUGGAGAUGGAGGUGGGCCAUGCUGGGAGGCCUUGUGGUGCGGUGGAAGGCACUGCGGCCGUGGAGUUGGGGCAGGGCUGCUGUUGGGGUGGUGCAGGAGAACACGCAUCGAGCACUUGUCGGCUUGCCUGGUCCAGAGGUUCAAUAAAUGUUGGUUUCUUUUUGCUUUCCUCCCCACACCUUAUGGCAGUGAUCUAGGAUCAGGAAAACUUGCUGGGAUUGGCAAUACCAUGAUGUUCUGUUUUUCUAAAGAAUCUCUUUUUGUAGGCUCACUCGCAUUUCACAGAAUCUGACUGGGUCAUAGUAUAACCCUGGUGGGGUCUUCAUGCGUUAUUAUUCAGUCUUUGACACAUGAGAAUCUGAGGCCAGAGCAAUGAAGAGGCUGUUCCAAUGUUAUGUGUGCUGGGGGAGCAGAGCUAGGGCUCUUCCUCUCCCUUCCCCUGUAGCAGUGUGCACAGAAGCCCCAGAACACUCCAGAAUGCCGAGUGGAGCUUUGCUAGGCUGCACUGCCAGGUGGGGCUCCAGGUAUAGUGGUUCCUACCAGGCUGUCAGAGCCACUUCCUUUUUCCCCAGAGGCAUACGGAAGCUCCUGAGUUCUGGUUCUCGUGGUCCCCUUGCAGCCCACAGUGCUACACUGAGCCCCUCCUGCAGGGAGUGUUUCCCUCUGUCCCAAGGAAAGCAAGGCCACAGUGCCCUCAGUGGUUCCUUGUGUUUCCCUGAGAAAGUUCACAGCUUGUCACCAUGAGCUACUUAAUAACAACAACAACAAAAAUCACAGGAGAGAAGUCAGUACGAUCAUGAUGAGUUUCACAGAACCUCAAAGCACUUUUAAGUCAUUAAGCAGCUUUAAAAAAAAAACUGAUUUCCCAAGGUACAGUUUAAAGUCAUUUUAUCUCUUUGACAUCACCAAAACUUGAGCCCUGCCUCUUGUCUCCAGGCAUGACAGUCUGACCUCAGAUAGGGUCCUGUUGUAGUCUCUGUCUGGGGCUACUCCCCACCUGCCUGGGAAGCAUUUCAGUCCAGAUGAGCAGCAUUUGAAAUUAGUUGAACACUCAGACUUUCACGGUUAUAAGACACAAACUAGGGAGUGAGCUUGCCCUGACAUUUGUGGGUCUUGGGUCAAGAGUGUGAAGCGAGGCCCCCAGUCUGCCAUCCACCCAAUUCUCUCUCUCUACUCCUGGUCUGUGUGUCCAAGCUGCGACCACUCCCACCUCCGCUUGGAACUGGGGUGCCUCUUGCCCACCUUCCAGGUCUACAUGUACACCCACAGGCCCUGGGAAAGGGCCUGGAAGCAGGCAUGAAGCCUUUUGGGCAGGGAAUCUCAUGGCCCCAGGGACCCAGAGCCUGGUCUUGAAGAAGAGGGUGGGUGCUCAGCCUAUGAAUGGGCACAGCCCAUGUUGGGAGGGGUGAGCUUGGGCCUUGACCCAAUGAGGUUCAGGGCUUGAGCCCUUGUUGCCCUGUCCUAAAGGCAGUACUGAUAAGGGGACACCUUGCUUCAAAAACUGAAGCAACAAAGGCAACUUGAAAUGUUUCCUGUUUAUAUGGCUGGUGGUUGCAUUUCUGCAUCCUCUGCUCUCCUUUUCCUCCUCAACCUUGGUCUCAUACAUAUGAUUGCUUCCUAAAGCAAAGCUGAUGAAACUGACCCAUUUCCUGUUGCUUGCCAAAGUAGUUCAGUAACCAGUAUGUUCCUUCUGCUGGUGAAACCUGACAGAGAACCUGGUAAUUCUGACAGCUGUUAUGUUUUGUGGGUUUCAGCCACUGACUUCCAUGGCCUCUCCUACCAUCCUUCUUUGAUGGCGUCUCUGCUCUCUGCUUCCACCUAUUUAUUUUUUCCCACUUGUCUACCCACAGAGCCAGGCUCCCUUACCUACCUGUUUAUUCUUUGACUGUGUGUUCCUUGAGCGUGUAUUUGCCUUGUUUUACUUGUAGGUGUGAAGGUCUAAGUGGAUGUACACACAGAACCUUCUUUGGGGUGUAUUUGUGUAAGGGACUGUCUGGAAGAAGUGGUUCUUCAACCUUUUUGCCCUUCAGUUCUCUGGAGGGCUUGUUACAACAGAUUGCUGGGUUUCACCCCCAGAGUCUCUAAUUCAGUAGGUCUGUGGUAGGCUUGAGCAUUUGCAUUUCCAGUUGAGGACCAUUGUUUUGGAAGAGUACAUUCAGAACAAAAAGUCAGAAAUAUUUAGAAUCAGAUGGUGGUUGUUUUGGUGAAAGCUUUUCUUGGAUGUGAGAGAGUCAGGGACCUGGCCUUAGCAUUCUUCGCAAUUCUACUGCCUUUUGUGGCUGUGACUUCCAGAAGCCAUAGGCACAUGCAGAUCCAGCCUCCGACUUCCUCUCCUCUCACCUGCCUUCACAUCUUCUCAGGGAAGGUCACAAAGUGCAGGAGCCACUUUCUCUUGUUCAUUCAGAGCCAGCUGGUCUGUGUAGUUCAUCCAGUUUGGUCUUGGGGCCCCAGAAUAAAAUGGGCCAAAUAUCAUCCUCACAAUAGUAAUACACUAUUAUUAACUAAUAUUUAAGAGCUCUAUGAUUUUCUCCAUUUACAGAAGAGGAAAUUGAGGCUUAGAGAUAUGAAAUAAUGUAUGCAAGGACUCAUAACAAGUAAUUGGUAGAGCCAGAGUUUGAACCUCAGUCCACUUGUCGCCAGCGCAUGCCCUUAUCUUCACUGGCAGGCCACCCUGCUUCUUGCAGGUAAGUUAGAGUGAUCCAUGCCAUGUGCAAGACUGACUCCGGUAAGAAGGAUCUGGGAUCCUCCUUGGAAAAGAGGCAAUCAAGCUGGAGACCGAAGGUGCUAACACAGAUUUCUGUGACACUCUUGUUCCAUUUGUCCUGUUCAUCAAACAGGGUCAAGUGAGGUGGUGAAUGUACAGCACUUGGACCUGUGGCUGGCAUGUAGGAAUGUGGUAGAGGGCAGCCAAGCCAUGAGUCCCCUUUGAGAGCAAAACAUAUCAAAUAUUCAGGAAUACUCUUACUGAGACCUCUAAGGAAAAACAUGUUAUGGGAAGAUGAUCAUAACAGCUAAUACCGCACACUUGCUAUUGCCAGUUCUGCACUAAGAUUUUACAUGUGUGAAUUCAUUGAAUCCCUGUAGUAACACUCAAAAGAGGUUCCACUUCCACAGUGUUACACAGAGGCACAGGCAGGUGAGGCAGCUCCUGAGUGCAGAGAUGGGAUCGACUCCAGGCAGUCUGAGUCCAGAGCUGACUCCUGACCACCAGCUGCACAGUAGAGACUCUUCCUCAUCCCUCCUAGAUGAGAGAGGGCAACUUGUAAAUACAUUGGUUCUUCUCCAAGUAUCAAUGGUCUUUGUUUUCAUCAAAAUCUGGAUAAGUAUUUUAAAACUUGAGAGACCAAUUUCUGUUGCUUUUCUUGAAAGAUAAGGUGGUAGGACAUAGGUUAGGCAUGGACCAUAAGAGUGGUGAAGGGGUUAGCUCUAUCCAGUGUCAAACCAUAAUGCUUCAAAUCUGGGACAAAAUUUGACAGACCCAUCCAUGGGGCAGAAGGGGGGAGGCAGAUUUCAGGUUCCAUAGUCUGUGAGCAUUUAACAGAAGAUGGAGGAGGUGCUGUGAGGCCAUGGGGAAAGGAAGGCUGAUUACCUGAAUGGGAAUGGGACUAUAUGAGAGCAAUCUGAAAAAUCUCAGUGGGUAUCAUCACCUCACAUCAUUACACCAAUGUAAAUUCUGCCUGAUUAAAAUGUGAGGUUUGACAAAAAUAUGUUCAAAAUACAUUCAGUGUUCUGGGGACUCUCCUAGGUGCCAAGUGUACAGCAUUGAGCAAAACAGAUAAAAUUCCUGCCCUGAAGCAGCUUGCGUUUUAGCAGAUAAAGACAAACGUUCCACUUUUUUACAAAGCUUUUUACAAAAGCUUGAAGGAAAUGGAAGUGGAUAUUUAUUAAACCUCUGGAGGAGUUGAAAUUUCUAAGAUUAGAAGCUGUAGAUGAACUCACAGAGGAAAAUAUUAUUAGUCUUGUCAGCAUAAACAUUCCCCAAAUGUUAAGGUUAUUUACUAUCAUGAGUUAUUCCUCAGUGUAAUUCUAUGUAACAUUGAGGUUUGUCUAGAUGUUAGGAUAGGUCCUCCAAAGUAGAUAUACUAGGUCAAGGGAUUUGAACAUCUGUUGGGUUCUAGAUACAUCACCAGGUUAAUUUCCUUGCCAAAGUUUAAUUUUUUUUUUUUUUGAGACAGAGUCUCGCUCUGUCAUCUAGACUGGAGUGUAGUGGCAUGAUCUCAGCUCACUGCAACCUCUGCCUCCUGGGUUCAAGAGAUUCUCCUGCCUCAACUUCCUGAUUAGCUGGGAUUACAAGCACCCGCCACCAUGCCCGGCUAAUUUUUGUAUUUUUAGUAGAGACAGCCUUUCACCAUGUUGGCCAGGCUGGUCUCAAAUUCCUGACUUCAGGUGAUCCACCUGCCUCAGCCUCCCAAAGUGCUGGGAUUACAGGCGUGAGCCACCACACCAAGCCUAAAGUAUAAUACUUUUAUAUUAAACAAAUCAAACCACCAAGAUGAAAAAUUGAGUUAACCCACCUGUUUGUCUGGGUGCUGCUCUCAGGCCUGGGCCCUGCUGUCAUUCUACCCCUCUCGCCAGGUGACAUAUCAUUCCCAGGUUUUCAAUGCUCCCUCUAUCUGUUAGGGACUCCUAAAGUUGUAUCUUUACCUAGACUUCUUUUUUCAGCUCCAGAGUCAUAAAGCCAUCAAGCUACUGGACCUCUCUCUUUGGAUAUCUCAUCCUUAACACAUUCAAAGGAAACAUCUUGGUCAACCCCCUGAAAUAUACUGCUGUUCUGGAAUUCUUUAUUUCCAUAAAUGGCACCUUCUGUCACCCAGUAGUUCACAUCAGAAACCCAGAGUCAUCCUUGACUUUGUUUUACUUAACAUUUAACCCAUCACCAAAUUGUAUUGAUUUUUGCCUCCCAGGUGUAGCCAUUCUCAUCAUUCGCCAUAGCUGUGUUCUCUAAAGUCGCCAGGAACACUGAAUUAGUGAAUACUGAAUCAUUACUCCUAAGGGAGAUACAGAGUUAGGUUCCUGUGAGCCUCUGGUCAUAUUUCCAUUGACUGAUCAAUACGUAGUAUCAGUUUCGUUGGUGUAAUAAUGUUGUAUGUUGGUAGAUGUUGUACGUUGGUAUAGCAUUACAUAUGUUGGUGUGAUGAUGUUUUAUGUGUGUUUCUGUUUAAACAUAUAUCUUAGCAUAUAGUUUUGAUUAACAUCAAACUCAUGCCCAACAGCACUAUAACUCAUGCCUGAACGAGCUUAUCUAACACAUGCGUUUCUCAUAAGGCACAUCACAGUCUUCUUGUGCUUAGGAGCACUAAGCAGCACUUUAGCACUGUGCUUGGGGACCAUUUAAACAGCAAAAUCACCAACAAAACACACCAAAAUGCAAAAAAAAUGUGGCACUAUAUAGACAGUUGAAAGGGUACUUGUUUAUAGUAUAAGAGCUGAAACAGGAAGGCAGAGUGUCACCAUUGUGGAGCUCAGCUGGGAAUGUGUGUGUUGACCAGCGCAACUUUUUUGCUGCUCUGCGCAUGCGCAGGCAUGACCAAAAGUGCUCUGAGUAUUGACUUUGGGGUUACAAACACCUUUUAGUGAGUAGGUGAAUUUGCAAAUGUGGAAUCCAGGAAUAAUGACGACAGACUGUUUAUCGUGAAGCCAUCCAUUUCUGUCUCCACUGCCAUCCCUUGUCUGGGGGUUGGCAAACUUUUUCUGUAAAGGUCCACGUGGUGCAUAUUUGAGGCUUUGCAGGCCAUCUGGUCUCUGCCGCCGUUACUGAAGUUGUAGAGUGAAAGCUGCACAGACAAUACAUACACGAGUCACGUGGUGGGAGGGGCGUGUGGGGGGGGGGGCGUGUUCCGGCAAAAUCUUACUCCUAAAAGCAGACUUGGGUUUGAAUUUGGUGUCCAGUCUGUAGUUUGGAUCCCUGUAGCUAGCCUAAGCCACCAUAAUGUCUCAUCUGGACUGGCUUCCUGACUUGUCCCUCCAUGCCUGUUCUUGACCUUCCCCAGCCAGUUUCCCAUAGUGAUAUUAAGUGCACAUUAGAUUCUGUCACUGCCGUACUUCAGAUGUCCAACUGCUUUCCAUCACACUUGGAAGAAAAUCCUGAAUCCUGAACAGCAUGGAUCACAGCACAGUCCCGGCUUGCUUCUCUGAUCUCCCUGGACACCAGUCUUCCCCUCUGUUUGCCCCAUCCUGGCCUCUUUCAGUUCUGUGACUGUUCCCAGCUGUUUCCUGCUUCAGCACCCUUUCCCACACAACAGUCUUCCCUUCCUGGAAUGUUCUCCUGCCUGGCAGCCUGGUUAAUUCAUGCUCACUCUGUGGUCACACCUCAAAUGUCACUUCCUCCAGGAGGCUUUCCCUGAUCCUCCAGUGUAAAUCAUAUUCCCCUCUUCUCAUCUCAGAGCACCCUCUUCUUUUCCUUCAUGACACUUAACAAUUUUCAUGAACCCACUUAUUUGGGCAUAUUUGUUUUCCACCUGCCUUCCCCAUUAGGCUGCAAGCUCCAUGAAGAUAGAAACCCAUCUGUGGUUGUCUCUGUGUUCUCUACCCCGUUACCAUCACGCACAUUAUAGACACUUCUGAAAACUUGGCAAAUCAGUGAAUGAUUGUACAACAUGCUUUUGUUCAUACAGAUUUUUGUAUGAAACUGCAAUCGAGGAAAUUGCCACCCUUUUAGAGUGUAUAGUAUAUCUUCAAAAAUUGACAGUGAUGAUUAAAAGCAAAAGACAUCUUGAUAGGUGAGUUUGUAAAUGGGUGUGCACGUGUAUCCGUAUUGUCAAAGGGUGAUUCUGAGACAGACACUCUGCGAACAGGUAUAUCUGGUGUGAAGUUUUCUCCCUGGGACUUGAGUGCUGCAUUCAAUCCUGCUGGUCUCACUUUUCCCCUAGAGCUUUGGAACUUUGCUGGUAACAUUUUCACAUGAGGAAGUGGAGGUAAAGUUUGCUUGAGGAGGCAUUUCAGCACCCCUCUUAAAAAUUGACUUUGCUCUUGUUUCUUCUCUCAAACCAUCACCUCAUCUCUCUUAGACUUUGUCGGUGCUAGUUGUUGUUCUUUCUACAGUGUUGCCACCAUCUGGGGAAGAAAUCUUUGAUUUGUCAGAGAAUCAUCUAAGCAAUGAAGUUCCAACUUGGGGGUUGUUCCCAAGUCAUUCCAGGAAUCCUCCAUGCCACUGAUGGACAGGCCACUUAGCAUAUUUUAGAAAGGUAACAGAUCAUUUCUAAGAUGACCUUCUGUAGAUUACUAGUGAAACCUAAAGCCUUAUGUAACUGCUUUUUUAUGUAUUUAGUACAGAAAUAACAUUUUCUAAUUAAAGGAAAUUAGAAAAUAAAGGCAAGCAAAACACUCCACAUACACACAGUUAGUCUCUCUCUCUCUCUCUCUCUGUCUCUGUCCAGAAAUGACCACUGUUACAUCUCUUAGGUCUUUUUGUAUGCAUAGAUGUGUGCACAUUUUUUUAACCAAAAUGAUGUAUUACUGUUUUAUUAUCUGAUUUUUUUGGAUGACAGUCUCCAACUUUGUAUUUCAAUAAAGUUCAUCUCGUUUAAUACCUUGUUUCUAUUCCGAUUUCCAUAACUGGCCCUCAAAUACCCUUCAAGGCUGGUUUGUCGAAAUCACCAUCUAAUCGAGUAUCGUGCCCUAUGUCUGGUUGUAACUUCCUUUUAGUCUCUUAAUCCAGCACAGUCUCUUAUUGAAGCAGCAGACCAGUUGCUGGUCUUGCCUCCAGAACCUCUGACCUGCUAGAGUGUGAGGUUGCUUCUUUAUGGUUAGGCUUAUUUCUCCAUCCUCUGAUUUCCUGUAUGGAAAAGCUUGCAGGAUUCAAGUUGUUUUUGACUAGAUCUCACCAGAGCUAAUUCAGUGUGCUUCACUCACUGUUACUAAAAAGGCCCACUACUGGGGAUGCUGAGAUUGACCCCUGGUCUAGGGCUGUGACAGCCUGAACCCACCAUCGUCCAGUUACACUUUCCCCCUAGAGACCAGCAAGUGACUUGUGUGGUAUAACUUUGCAUACAAAUCGUUUACUUAAUGGUUUUGUACCCAGUGGUCAUUCUUGCCUGAACCAUACCUUCCUUGGGUUUUGGGAAAUGUUUCUGUAAUUCUUUCAUUUCUUCUAUAAAGUAGAGCUUUCCUGUACUGCCUGGGGCCGUCUGGUUACCCUGACACAUGGUUCCCACUGGAAAGGCAGGAUCUGUGCUAAUGCUUUCCCUUUCCCCAUUAACUUUCACAGUAAGGAGUUUAAUAACCACUUCACGUAGUAACACGUGGUUUUUUUCUGUCUUUCUAACAUUAUACAUUCAUGGAUUUUUAUUGAUCUGGUGUGUUCUAAUCAUUACUCUUUUGUUACAACUUUUAGGCAGUGAGACCCCUUCAGCUAGGUCCUGUGACCUUUUGACAGAACUUCUAUAAUCUUGAAAAUCUGUGUUCAUUCAUGGCACAAAUGCCCCAAGCUCAUCUUGUACUUUUCAGUGGUAUGGGACAAUGGUAUUAGAGAGUACAAUCAGGGUAUUGGGGGUGGUUAUUGGUGCAGAGGUGACUUGUUUCUAGAGAACUUCAGUGGACAAAGCUGGAAAAUAUAUACUGUUAAAAUUUAAGAGUUCAGGUGGACAUGUCCAGUUUAGUUUUAAAAUCCUUAUGCUUUCACUUUCCUUAGUAAUUAUUUUAACUCCCUUUUUCUGGUAUGGAAAAAUCUUUAUUUUUUCUUUAACCUAUAAAUGUAAAGAAUGUAGUUUCGAAAUACCAAUAUUUAUAUUAUUACCAAUAUGGAACUACAGAGGAAAGUUUAAUACUUCUUUGUAAUUUUUGUUUUGUUCUUAAAAUGCAUUCCACUAAGGGUAUGUAUUAAAAAUACUGUGUUCUAAAAUUCCUAAAAAUAAAUUCUUCCUCAGAGAGCAUGUCACCCAGUUUGAUGUAUGGUUAGGCUCAUAUCAUUCAGUUUCUUUUCAGUUUAGGACAUUUUGAAUGGAGCUUUUUUAAGAUGGGUAAUGCAUUACGUGGCUGAAGGGUCAAAACUAUGUAGAUGUGGGCCGGGUGCGGUGGCUCACGCCUGUAAUCCCAGCACUUUGGGAGGCCGAGGUGGGCGGAUGAUGAGGUCAGGAGAUUGAGACCAUCCUGGCUAACAUGGUGAAACACCGUCUCUACUAAAAAAUACAAAAAAAUUAGCUGGGCGUGGUGGCGGGUGCCUGUAGUCCCAGCUACUCGGGAGGCUGAGGCAGGAGAAUGGCGUGAACCUGGGAGGUGGAGCUUGCAGUGAGUCAAGAUCACGCCACUGCACUCCAGCCUGGGCGACAGAGCAAGACUCUGUCUCAGAAAAAAAAAAAAACAACUAGGUAGAUGUUUAAUCUAGAUGAUGGGUAUGUGAAAAAUUGUUAAAUCAUUCUCUCUACAUUUCUUUUGAUAUUGGAAAGUUAAAAUAAUUAAACAAUAUAGAGAAGUAUACACAAUGAAGUCUUAACCUGUGAACUUUGUUUUUUUUCUUUUUUAUUAUUUCUGUUUUGCAGAUGAGCCCUAUGCACUUUGUUCCCUCGUAGAUAACCAUUUUUCUUAGUAUCUCGCUUAACCCUUGCGUCUUUCAUUUUUAGAGGUUCUAGUGUGUGUAUGGGUGUGUUCUUAUUCCCUUACACAAAGGAUAACAUAACACAUACAGUCUGUUGUUCUACGUCUUAACUUUUUUCUCUUAAUAAUACAUUCUGGAACUCUGCAUAUUUGUACAUAGAGAUUAUCUUCAGUCUUUUUUAUAACCUUAGAGUACUCCAUUUUGUUGAUGUGUGAUGAUGGCACAACAACAUAAUCUUGGAUUGUGUCUAAUCCUCUGUCUUUUCAAAUCACCUGUAAUAGAUAACCUUGUAGACAUGUCAUUUAAUACUUUUGUAGGUGCAUCUGUGAAAUGAAAUCCUAGAAAUGGGAUUAUAUAGUCAAGGGACAGAUACAUCUGUCAUUUUUAAAAGUUAUUGACAAAUUCUUCCUGUAGGGUUUAUACCGUAUUCUACUCAUGCAAGCAGUAUGUGAAAGUGCCUGUUUCCCUAGAACAUCACCCAUGGAAUCUGUUGUCAAACUUUUGGAUUUUUGCUGGUAGGUGAGAAAUGGUAUUUUGUUAUAGCUUUAAUUUAUAUUUCUGUUAUUAUAAGUAAGGUUGAUCAUAUUUUCAUGUAUUUAAAUGUCAUUUUGUGUUUAUUUUUAUGUGGAGUGUGUUUUGAAUUUCAGACAUUUUCCCACUAUGUUGUUGGUCUUUUUCUUCUUUAUUCUGAAAGCUCUUUAUGUAUAGUCUUUGCUAUGAGUUGCAUUUUUUUUCCAGUUGAUCAUGCAUGUUUUGGUUUACUUAGUGGUGGUGGUUUGCCCUUUGGAAGUCUCUUUCAUUUUAUGUAGUCAAAUUUAUUUUUUUUAUGGCUUCUGUAUUUUUAGUCAAAGUUGGAGAGGCUUUGCCUGUCUCAUAUUUUUCAGUUCCUUUGGGUACUUUUGUAAUUUUACUUUUUUCUGUUUACAUCUUGGUACGUUUGGUGUUUCUUCUAGAGCAGCAGUUCCUAGCCUUUUUGGCCCCAGGGACUGGUUUUGUGGAAGACAAUUUUUCCAUGGACUGGGGGUGGGGGUGGUUUCAGGAUGAAACCAUUCCACCUCAGAUCAUCAGGCAUUAGUUAGAUUCUCAUAAUGAGCGCACAAUCUGGAUCCCUCGCAUGCGCAGUUCACAGUAGGGUUCAUGCUUCUGUGAGAAUCUGAUGCCACUGCUGAUCUGACAGGAGGCGGAGCUCAGCCGGUAAUGCUCACUCACCUGCCACUCACCUCCUGCUGUGUGGCCUGGUUCCUAACAGGCCAGAACUGGUACUAGUCUGCGGCCGGGCCAGGGCGGGGUGGGGAGUGGUUGGGGACCCCUGUUUUAGAGUAUGUUCUGAGGCUUGGAUGCAACUUUAUAUUUUUUCAAUACUCAAUUGUCCCAACAUUAUUUGUUUAAAAGUUUAUAUUUUUCCCAUAGUAUCAUAACCCCUACUUUAUCAUUUACUAAGUUCCUAUAGGUCUGGGAGUCUAUUUCUGGACUCUAUGUUUUUCCAUGGGUUGAUCUGUUGUUAAUGUUUGAAAUUUAUAUCAUCUUUUCAUAUCUGAAAAGACUAGUUCUCCCUCGUUGCUCUUCCCCUUCAGCCUUGUCCUGGCUAUUCUCCAUGUUUGUUAUUCCAUAUGAACUUUAGACCCAACAUUCUUGAUUCCAGAAAAAAAGCCUGUUGGUAUUUCCAUUGGGAUCACAUUAAAUUUAUAAAUUUCUUAGGAGGAAUUAACAUCUUUACAAGGUUGAGUCUUCCCGUCAAAGACAAUGUUUUCUAUGUGUUCUUUUUUUGUGUGUACUUUAGUAAUGUAUAAAAGUUUUCUGUAUAUAGGUUGUAUACAUGUCUUAAGUUAAUCCUUGUAAAUAAUAUCUUUCAUUAUCUCCUCUUGUUUGCAUAUGAGGACUAUUUAUUUCCACAUGUAUUUUUGACAGCUUUAUUGAGAUAUAAUUCAUGUAAUUUACCCAUUCAAAGUGUAUAGUUCAGUGGUUUUUAGGAUAUUCACAAAUUGUGCAACCAUCACUACUAUCUAAUUUUACAACAUUUUUGUCACCCCAAAAAGAAACUCUGUACCCAUUAGCAGUCAUUCCCCCUUCUCAACCUCCCCCAGCCCCUGGAAACCACUAGUCAAAUUUCUAUUCAAGACGUUUUCUAUAAAUGGAAUCAUGCAAUACAUGGUCUUUUGCAGCUGGCUUCUUUCACUUAGCUUGUUAUCAAGGUUCAUCCAUGUUGUCGCAUGCCUUUUUUUAGGAUAGCCAUCCUUGUGAGUGUGAAGGGUACCACUGUGGCUCAGAUUUGCUGAUUUCUAUAUGUAUUUAGUUCUCUUUUGUGAGAUUUCAUGAGUGCAGGAGGCUGGCUUUCAAUUCCAGAUCCCCAGUGCCUCCCAAAGUGUCUAGCAAAUAUUUGGUACUCAAUAAAUGCUUAUUGAAUGAAUGCUUGGAUUUAAUAUACUUCUAGGCCACCUCUACAUUUUAAAGUUAAAAUGUAGUUUGGCAUAUAUAAAUUAAUUUUUAUCUUUUCCUAGGUGAAACAUAAUUACAGGGUGAGUUUUUCCUCCGGGAAAGCCUGGUAAAAGCAGUUUUGACUGAUAUGUGGUUUGUGCUGGUCAAUAUUCCUUUUUCUUACAUUAAAACGAAUGAUUGAGAGUUGCUGGUACAUAUGUCUAAGUGUCUGUGUCUCAUCUUUUCAGGAGGAUGAUUUUUAGCUCUAGAUUCUAAUUGUUAUUGAAAACUACUUAGUAAUAUGUAUAAGAUAGAGGUGAGAAAUUAGGUAAAGUUCUGGGCCUGGGAAAAGGGAGUUUUGAAUGAGAUGGAUCAGUUCAUAUGUAUUUUACAAGUUCUAGGUUUACCAAGGGCUGUGUUCCAGAACCUCUUUUGUAAGCUAGUUGUGUGGACACAUCACAGUUAACAAUAAAGUGCUAUCAGCUAAGAUUUGGGUCUCAAGCUUGCCUUAAAGGAGAUAUGGGAGAGUAUAGUUGAUGCAUGCGUGAGAGCAGGCGGUGUGUAUGGGAACUCCCUGUACCUUCCACUCAAUUUUGUUGUGAGACUAAAACUGCUCUACAAAAAUAAAGUCUGACUGGAUGCGGUGGCUCAUGCUUGUAAUCCCAGCACCUUGGGAGGCUGAGGCAGGUGGAUCACCUGAAGUCAGGAGUUUGAGACCAGCCUGACCAAUAUGGUGAAACCCCAUCUCUACUAAAAGUACAAAAAUUAGCCAGGCAUGGUGGCAUGCGCCUGUAGUCCCAGCUGCUUGGAAGGCUGAGACAGGAGAGUUGCUUGAACCCGGGAGGCAGAGGUUGCAGUGAGCCAAGAUUGCACCACUGCACUCCAGCCUGGGUGACAGAGCGAGACUCCGUCUCAAAAAAACAAACAAACAAACAAACAAAAACUAAAUAAAGUCUAGUAAUUUUUAAAAAGAGUGAGAGAGAACACAGCUGAAAUACAUAUACUUUUUAGGAAAAGGGAAAUAAUUAAAUAUCAGAAAAAUAAUAUUGAAGAAGAAAUAUUUCUCUUUAAUGUCAGUGUUUGAAGAAAGGUAUUUUAAUUAAAUCAGAUCGUGUGUGUUUGCAGGAGACUUUUGGACACUAUCCAAGGAUUUUGAGAUUGACAAUAUUGGAUUUUUAUAUUGCCCCAAUUUUCUUUCAAAAUAUGUGACUGUUAAGAUUAUUAUUACCCUUAUAUUAUUAGACGUGUUUGGGUUGGGGAUAGGAAAAAGACAGAGGGAGAUUGAUUGGUUGACUGAUUCAUUCGUUCAUUGGUUAAAUGGGACAGACUGAUUUCUCUAACUGUCUGAGCCUGAGAGAUGGGGAAGGUAGAACAUGGCUCAGAAGAAUAUGCAUUUCCUGUAAGAAAACAUUUGUCUGAAAGGAAUUAUAAUAAUUGAGAAUUAAGCUGUAUGAUACAGAAGCAGUAUCUGAAGGGCAGAUGGAUAAUAGAAGGUAGCUGUGGUGCAACUCGAAUCAAUGGCUGGAAAGCCACAGGAGGCAGAUUCCCACCAGGCCCUAAGGAAGGACACCGUACCGAAGCCCUCCACAUGUGGACAUCCAUGGGGCCUGCGAUUUCUCUGGUACUGGAGGUAUUCCAGAUGAGUGCCUUGUGAAGGGACUGCCGGAGACUGGCAUCCAACAGAACAUGGAUGUGGGACCAGAGCAUCUUUAAGGCUUCUUCUCAGAGAGGCUGGUAGUUCUGAGCGUGUUUACAGUUCCAUUGAGGGAGAAAAAAGGAAGAAGCAGGGAAAAAGAGUUAGGUGGGGAUUUUCCCCGUCAGCUCAGGAGACCUUGUUUCUCUUCAGAGAGAGUAGGAUGGUAGAAAACAAAUUGUUUUUUGUUUCAUGGUCUGUUUAUUAGUAGAUUAUUGGUUAAGAUGCUUUUAGCUUCAAGGGACAGAAACCAACACAAAGUGUAUAAACAAAAGGGAAAACUGACUGACUGGUUAACAAGAAGUUCUGAGGUCAUCAGCUCCAGGGUUGGUUGUAAAAAACUGAUGUUCUUUCUGUAUUUCUGCCCCAUGGUUUGUGGUAUGUCGGUCUGAUGGCUGCCACAGUUCUAGGCAUCACAUCCAACUCAACAGUGUCCAUGGGAAAAAGAGCAUCUCUUUAAAGCAAGAAAACCUUUUCCAGAAGCUUCCUGCAGACCUCCCUUCACACCUCGUUGACCAGGCUGAUGGUGUGUGCCAGUGCCUAAGUCAAGUCAUUGACAACAGGAAGAAGAUGAGCCCUGGCUGAGUUAAACUGACCAGGAUGUGCAUCCCCCCCAUGCUGGAAGUGAGGCCGUCUUCCCUGAGAGUCAGUAUCCGAACAGAAAGAUCACCCAAUGCAUGUUGUUUUUAAAGUACUUAUGGAGAUCUCUGUGCCGUGGUGGUAUCAUCCGUAUGAACCAUCCAGGCUGUAGUCAGAGAAUCAGAGACUCGCUGUGUGAUCUCCAAGAAGCCGUAUCACCUGUGUCCUCCAUAGCAAGAGAACGUAUUGGAAGCCCCUCCUAGCUUUCGAAUUCCAUCAUCGUCUCUCCUUCUCUCCCCUUCAGCUCCCCUCCCACUGCCCACGGAGGCUGCUGUGUGACAGAGGAAGUUUCUUAUCAAGUCCUCAGUGAUCUAUGUAAAGAAGAGAUGGUGUUUUCUCAGGCUCUUAGCACUUUGUUCUGUUGGUUUCACAAACUAAUUAUUGUUCAGAAUUUAAUUUUUAGAAAAUUUUAAUGACUUUUGUAAGAGGUUUAGUUAACAUACUGCACACACACACUCUCUGUCUCUCUCACACACUUAGCUUUUCUAUGUGUAUAUACAUGUACAUGUAUCUAUAUUCUAACCUGGCUUUGGUGGAACCAGCUUUCUUGCUCUGUGCACAGACAUCUUCCUGCUGCUCGUUUCAGCCCUGAUGUGGUGGAAUGUGUCUGAAGCAUGCGUUUCUAGGUCUUUUCCUUAUGGCCUCCACAAAGUGGUCUUGAUGGCCCUCAGUUCUGUUCAGCAGUAAUGCAAAGUGAAGAUGUUUCUCUGACUCAAAAGUGAGAUGACAUUAAUUGAGCGCCUACCAUUUGUGCUCCUUCUAUCGGAGACUUAGAUACGAUAUUUAUGCUUAAAAUGGCUCUGAAAUUAAAGGGCAAGGCCUGAGGUGCAGUAUCUCCUCUUUCUAGCCCUCCCAUUCAGGCCUGUUUAGCUACUUUCUCCCCACUUCCAAAGGGUGUCUCUUGGAAAGAAGCAGGACUGUCCCCUAAAUUGGAGCAGAUAGCAGCCUGGGGCCUCGAGCCCCCGCUUCCCUUUGUGUUGUGCACUGGCUCCAGCGUGGCGCCCGUCUUUGAAGUCAGGUGGAAGCCCCACAGGCAGGGCUGCUGCCCUCCUGCUCUCUGGCCAUUCAGCACAACCUUUAGUCUAGGAAAAGUGCCAGUCUUCAUUUCCAAGUAUCAUAUCUCCCUAAAUGGGGCAAUCUGCUUUAAAUGCCUUCUCCACUGGCGCCUUCCCCAUCUCACAAUUGGCAUAAUUAAAGGGAAAGGCUCACCUCCUUUGCUGCCUAUGUGUACUGGGUCAGGGCGUUGGCUGGGGGCCGCUGGUGUGUAUGCACGCCUGCCCUCGCAGAGACGCUCCCUUGGCCCUCCAGCCCUUGAGUGAUCAUUUUCAGAAGUGUUCAGAGCCACUCUGCAAGCAUACACUUUACCUUUGCAUUUUCCCUACUGUGCUCAACUCAAUAACAGGCAAGCUGGUUACUAUGAUCCAUGAAGCUUUUUGUAUCUUGCUGGAAAAAAAUGCACUCUGAGCUGAAAGAUAAUCUCCCUCGAUGGUUCCAAGUCAGAAUUUGCUUUAUGACUCAUGACAUUUGGUGUCUUUCUCCAUGAAGAUUUCCCCCUUCUCCUCGUCCACUCCCAGCUUCAGAUGUGUGCGAUGGUGUGGUUCAUCCUUAGAGAGUCACUGCUGGUCCCAAGGAAUGGUGUGACAUGUAGGAAGGCUCCCGUGGUUGCUGGUCCCCUCUGAUCUCCAGUUCAGCUGCCACGCCAGCACCCUCGAUUAAGCUCCUUUGGAACCUGGGUUUUUAUUACCUGCCACUCAGCUUAAAGCAGAGGCCUCUCAGAGGGCAUGCCUGGUAAUGCAGCUGCCCUCUGUUCUGCGGAGGCAGCCUCAGUCUCCAUCACCUCCCUCUCAGAAGUCAGUCUCUCAGCAGCACUGGGGGGCCCACUGUGUGCAAAGCCCUGUGCCCACUGGUUCAGCCAAGAAUGGAAUAGAAAACAACCAUGCCCAUCUGACUACUGUAAAGAGGGACAGGAGAACCUUGGGACAGAGGCAUACCUGUGCUUGCCCAAGCCUACCUAGACCACCCUCUUGUGGGAUGUGCACUGGGAAUUGAUUUCCCAGUGGUGGGGACAAACUUGUGCUCAUUUCUGCCUCGUUUGUCACCUAGAUUCUCUUUACGAUGACAUCUAAUGUGCAGAAGUCCAGCCCGUAGCAGCAGCAUUUGACUAAUGUGGGAAGUUCAGGAAUUUUGAGCCUGGAAAGUCCUGGGAAGGAAAAUCCCUCAUGCUUCAGCAGGGCUGUGUGGCCGGUUCUCCAUGUGCUUCAGCAGAGUUUUCUUUCUCUUUUUCUUUUUUUUUUUUUUUUCAGCUGUGAAAAAAGCAGUGCCAGCUGUUUGGUAAAAUAUGGGUCAGUGAGAAAUAGGAUUUGCUUUAUAGAAGUUAACUUUGGAGAAUCGUGUCCUCAAAAAGAAAAGAAGUCUAAAGAUAGGAGGACUGAGGGAAUCCUGGGUGUGGUGAUCCUAACCCCAUAAGUUAGCUUGGGGUGCUUUCAGGAAGAUUUUGGUUUCCAGCAGUUCAGAAGGGAGGUGGGCAUGAUUUGGUGCAGAAGGGGGAGAGGUGAGGGAGAAAAUCACAUGCAGACACGUUGAGUAGUGAUAAACCACGAGACAGACUCUGCACGGCCGGACAGAGGGCAUCUUAUUAGAGUGGAAAAGAAUAGUAUUUUAUUUUGCUGUGAACAAGAUAGUUUGGGGAGUGGAGAAGAGCUCCCAGGGUGGGCGAUGACAGGUGUCUGGGGGACACUGGAGCCAGUGGAUGCAGCAAACAGCUUGGACUUCAGUCCCUUUUCUAGCAAAGGAGCUGCCCCUGUGGGGUGGGGGGCUGAGGAGGUUGGAGACCAUUUGAAAUAGCUUCUGAGCAUGUGUGUGCACACAGGCACAUGCAUGGCUGGUGUCUCUUAGAGAAAAGGUAUUUAGAGAAAAGCAAGGUUGUGAGUGGCCUGAGAGCAGUUACAAUUGAUUUUGAAUAUGGAAGCAAUUCUACCUAAUCCAGAGAAUAUACAAAGUAUACUUUGGAAAGGGGCAGUAAACUUUUCUGGUUGGCCUGCCUUCCUCCCUCCUUUUCUUCUUCCCUUUCUCUCUUCUUCCCUUCCUCCCAUCCUUCCUUCCUUCUGUGAUCUUUGUGGGAGAGCAAGAGCUAUUUGUAUGUAGUGAUUAUAAAUUUGGUACUUACAUAGAAUUUCUCAACAUGUUUCUCAGAGAUUAACAUGAUCCCUGGGAGAAUCUGGAAGGUCUAUCUUUGGGGUGUCUUCUGAAGAAGAUUGUGAUUCUUAUGGCAUCUGCCUUCUCAAGCCCUUAGUCAUUAAUUAUUUACUCUCAUAUCUCUCAAUGCAUGCAGUUUAGUGCCUAGCACUAAGUGAUGGUUUGUGUGCAUGGUUGGCCCAGCAGAAAUAUGUUUGUCCAUCCAUCCAUCCAUCCAUCCAUCCAUCCAUCCAUCCAUCUAUCCAUCCAACCAUCCAUCCAUCCAUCCCUCCCUCCCUCCCUCCCUCCCUCCCUCCAAAUCAUUCAUCAAAUAAGGGAACCUUCCCCAAAGGUCCCAGCUGUUCUCUCUCCCCUUCUUAUAGGCUAUAACUGGGUAACAUGCCUAGCCCAGAUCAUUCACUCCCAGGCACAGCAAACAAUUAGCUUAGACUAGCCAGGAUUGGUUCUUGAGUCACACAAAGGGGAGGUGGAAGGUGGUUGGAGGUGGUGGUGGGGAGAGUGACAUCUAAACUAAAUCCUGUCUCUCCAGAAGAGAAAGAGGGAAUGGCUAUUAGGAAGGCAACUUACAGUGUCUGCUUCAACAUGUUCAUUUUUUUUUAAAUGUUUCACUCUGAUUGUAGUGUUUUUUAACUAUACUAUUCUCUAAAUUUGGCUGUGUUUACUAUGGUAAUUAUUUUAAUUAAGUUCUAUUUGAUUAUUUGUAAUUCACCUUGUUUUACAACUUUUGAUUGAUUUUAUAGUAUAAAUACGUAUACUGCAAUAAACCAUAUGAUACAUAAAAGAAUUUAGGACAGGAUCAGGAUAAAUACAAAUAAAUAUAGAAGUUCAAAGUUAGGAAGAAAAAGAAUUACAGAUAUGCAGACAAUAAGUCCCUUACAUUGCUACUUAGCUGAGCUUCAUAACAUCAAAGAGAAAAGGCAAAUGUGGUCGCUGCGGUCAUUCUUGCUGUCAGAGAAGGAAGGUGCACCAGGUCCUCAAGAGGAGCAAAGAUUUUUUUAGUUCUUUUCAACUAAAUUUUGCAUGUGGACUUUUAUCUAGGAAGCACUGAGAGGUAUCAUGAACAGGGUGUUUGGCAUCCCCACAACAGAUGAAAAACUGGGUUCUUACAGCUCUUCUCACAGCAGUCCUCAUUGGAAGCUCAAGGCCUAACAUGAAAAUGCAACUCAGCAAAUGUUAUUCCCUGGAAGGCCAAAAUAACAGGUCUGAGUACUUCUUCUUAUCCUUCUACUGGUUUGAUGCAACACAAAGACCCAAAACACUCAGCAGAACUGCCAGUCUACGUGCCUAUCAGACAACCUUCAAGACUAUUACUUUUUUUUAACUGGCGUGUUCACGCAUGUGUGUGCCUAUGUGUGUAAAUAUAUCUGUAUAUUUAUGAAUAGAUGUAUACAUCCAAAAUACUAUAUAUAUAGGAAGAGAUCAUUUGAGGGUAGAUUCCAUUGCCCACCAUGCUGUAUUCUAGCUCAUCAAUUGAGGCUUUAGGAAUCGACCUGGUAAGGUUGACAUCUGUGGAAAUUAAGGCCUCUAUUUAAAAUGCUCACAGAGGAGAGUUCUAUUUUUGUAAAUAGGAUAAUUGGGUGGAAAACUGUGCUAAUGUCUGUCUUUAUUUAACCACUCCAAGGGACAAAGCCUAACUGCUAAAACCAUGAGGCCAUAACCAAGACACCACCAUUUACCCAGGGACACCGUCAUCUUUAUACUGCAAUUUUAAAAGAGUAUGGAGGUCAGAAGCCAGACAGUUGGUUUCUGUAUUAAUGUCUCCAGGGGAUGAACAGAGGGUGAGAAGGAGCAGAUAGACAGAGGCAGGUCUGGACGGGAGGUUGGAGAGCGGUCAGCGAUGUUCUCCCAGCUGUCAGGAAUGUUAUGUGGGAAGAGGUUAGGGAAGAGAGUUAGGGGAAAUAUCAAAUGAGGGAAUGACUGUGUCCUGGCAGAGGUGUUAUUUCCUCUAAACCACUUUUGAUGAUCUUCUGUCCUUGUGAAGAUGUUGGGAGUGGACAGUGCCAGGACAGUAUGAACUGUUGUGCGGCGUGGCGGAUACCAGAGGAGGGUGCAGGGAACAAGCAUUUAUAGAGCCUGCCACUAUUUCACCUGCUGACCUCCUUUGAGAGGCAGUAUUAGGAAAUGGUUAGAGUGCAGCUGUGUAAUCAGAGGCUCUAAGCCCGAGUCUUCUCCCAGCAAACGAGGAUAAUAGCGGCGUCUUACCUCAGACCUGUUGGGAGCUGCCGUGAACACGUCAUCCACGCCCAGUAAAUGCUAGUUAACACAGUGAUGGCCAUCCAGAGAGCUUUCUUAGCCUGAUGUGAAGUAGAUCUCAGGCUCUGCAUUUUCCAGCAGGGUAAACUGAGGCAUAGAGAGACAAAUUCACUUGUGCAAGAUCUUUUAUCUAUUAAGUGUCAAAGCUAGGAUUCAAGCCAGGUUUUCUAGCACUAAAGCUUAUUGGUUUUUUCUGUUCCAUGCUGCCUGAAUUCAUAGGUAAUUCACCUGUGUCUUAUAACCCAGACACGUGAUGUGGGCCAUGAACCACAGCACCUUUCUGGGUCCACUGUGCUGGUGGAUAGCUUUCUGUUCAUGACAAUCACGUCUGAUGAGCUUGGCAGUGAUUUGUAUGAUGACAGUGACCGUCCAGCAGUAUGUUAAGGAGUCUGGGUCAGGAGGGACUUUCUUCAUUUGUUUUUGCCACAUCACCCAGAGAACAUCCCUGUAAAAGAAGGCGGUUUGAUGAACUUGGAGGAACUCCCCAGCACUCUACUUGUGACCAUGACAAUUGUGACAGUUUUUCCUUCACACUGUAUUCAAGGUCAGGUUUUUGUUCUUGGACCUUGUUAAAUCGAGGAUAGUGGGCUUGAAUGACUUGGUGUAUCAUGGAAAUAGCCUCAUGUGGUGUUAGCUUCUGCCUGGGGUCACCAGCUGCUCCCACAAAGCUGAGUAGCCAGUAAUUUCUUACAAAUCUUUUCAUAUUAAUAGAAAAAUGGAAGGCAGAUGGUGGGCCAGGAGGAGUGCUUUUUCUUUGAGGCUUUGAGGGCCUGUCAGGGGAUGAAUUUUGUGUCCCCCUCCCCACUCACAUGUUGAAGUCCUAACCCCCAGUACUUCAGCAUGUGACCUUAUUUGGAAAUAGGGUCAUUGCAGAUGUGGCUAGUUAAGAUGAGGUCCCACUAAAGUAGGGUGGGCCCCUAGUCUAGUAUGACUAGUGUCCUCAUAGGAAGGGGAAAUUCAGACACAGACACGCCCACAGGGACCAUGGCUCAUGAGCACGAAAGCAGAGACUGGGUUAAUAGGCAUAGAAGCCAAGGAACAGCAAAGAUUGCCAGCGCCCACCGGAAACUAGGAGAGAGGCAUGGAACACACCGUCCCUCACAGCCUCGGAGGGAGCCGGCCCUGUCGACACCGUGAUCUUGAACUUCUGGCCUCCAGAACUGUGAGAUAAUAAAUUGUGUUGAUUAUGCCCCCCAGCUUGUGGUGCUGUGUUAUACUAGGCCAAAUAAAGUAACGUAGGGCCCAUGGAAAAACAGUGACUUACAAAUUCCAGAAGAAAAGCUAGAGCCCCUCCUAUGCUUUGGUUAAAGUUUCCAUCGGAGCGUGGGAGUCUGGAUGUAGGGCUGAGGGUUCCAAAAGUGUCAUAGAAAGCAGAGAAGCGGCUCAGAUGGGCAGACCAGCUUCCGAAGAACACGGGUGUUCUGUGAAGGUCAUUGCGUGGAGGUGACCUUUUCCCUCACUGAGUUUUUUAGAGAAAGCAAUUUUGUCCUUUCAGGUUGGAAAAAUAUUUUCUUCAAGACCACAAAGUGACAGUUAAAAAAAAAAAUUGGCCACCUGCAAGUUUAAAUGUCACCAUCUAGAACAGCUCUGCCUGAUAGAGCUUUCCGUACUGAUGUCUCUCUCGGUCCACCCUCUCUCCCACAGUAGCUACUUGCCACGUGACCAGUAAGCACUUGAAAUGUGGCCAGUGGGGCCGAGGAACUCAAUGUUUUAUUUUAAUUAAUUUAAAUUUAAAUAGCCACUUGUGCCCGCUAGCUAAUUCUAUGUGUUGGUCAGUAUGGCUCCAGAUCACCAGAAUAGUGGUGGGAUGGGACCCAAGGGAAAAACCGGGGGUGCCUGGAUAUCCAGUGGAGGCCACAGGAGGGCUGGGGCUGAUGGGUCACCCUGGCUUGGCUAGUGCCCUUGUGUGUGGUCUUGUCCUCAGCCACAGGGGCCUAGGUGGGAGUAAAAGUGAAGUAACACAGGCAGAAUUUUCUGGAUGCUUUACUAAAGAGAUGCUUAAUGUGAGGCUUUGUCUGCCGUUCCUUCUCUGAUCCCAAAGUAUCUUCGACUGGUUUAGUGCUCGAUAGAGAUGGGGUAGAUUAAGAUACUUGAAGAAAAGCCAGGAAGCUGGGUCUCUGGAUAUGGGCAGACCGAGAUGUUUCUUUGCAGGUUUCAAGUGCCGGCCCUUGAUGUACCCAGAGGGGCCGCUAGUCCCAACGCUAGGAAGGUGGGAACGUCCAGAUGCAGACCACCUUCUCCGAAGCUAGGAGGGUUUCCCCUGAGUCUGUCAUACUAGACUUAUUGAUUGCAGAUGCCUGUCAAAAGCUACUGAGGCUCAGCCACCUCUGCGUUCUUCACAGUUGCCACCCUGCCUCCAGCCCCUGAAUUGAUGGCUGCUGCAGGGAGUGUGACCAGAGGAUGCCGUUUGGAGAGUAGUCACAUGGGACAUCUCAGAAUCUGAGAUGGAACCCCAACUGGGCAGUAUUUGGUGCAGUUUCACACCGAAAAGGGGUCCCUGUGACUGAUUUGGCCAGCCCUGGACAAAUGAGUGUUGUCAUUGUAUCACCAGCGGCUUUGGCUCAGUGCGUGGUAUAAUUUAAAAAUUGCCUCUUUUUCUAGCUCUACUUAGUUAUCAUUCUGAUUUCAGAAAGAAACAAAUGGUUCACCAAGUCUUAUAAUAUCUCUAACCCCGAGACAAGCGAGGGGUGUGAGGCAGAGACACGCUAUGUCAGGCUACAGCCUGCCUCUCCCCUGGCCCACGUCACCUUGGCCGACUGGACUCUGAACAGUGAAGGGAUAGCCUAGAAGGAAGGAGCUGAGCCACCUGACUGAGUGGUGAGGUUGGUGGAUGUGCAGAUGGAAUUCCUGGCAUUGAAUUGGAGGGCAGGAGUUUUAGUUUGAGUAGAGGUUAGGAAGAUAAAAGAGGUGCGAGAAACCUGUUGUCAACCUCCAGCAGAUUUGGUAGCUUGUGCCACAUGUGCAGCAUCAUGCUUGGGGACUCAGGGGACAUCAAUAAGUAGUCAGUAGCUGAUGCUUAUAUUGGUAGUGCCUACAGUGUGCCAAGCCCAGUUCUGAGCUUAAUACUUUACAUACAUUAGCCACUUCAGCACAGUCGCUGUCUUUUCCAAGCACUCUUAAACUCAUUGCAGGCAAGAUUAAACCAAGCAACAAAAGACAUCAAGCGAUGCAGGGUAAUACGUGAUGAGCACUGUUAGGCCCAAAGAGAAAACCCUGAGGUCCCCAGUGACAAGGGAUGCAUCAUUUGAUCUGGGGUUUGAAGGAUGGUCUUGAUUUGGAAAGGUGGCUAGGGAGCAAGCUCGAGGUUGCCCCACACAGGGGUGCACAAGGCCCGGCUGGGGGACAGUGGGUGUCUCACUUGGGCUGACUGGAACAAGUUCCAGGUCACAGGUUUUUUUAUUUGAAUGUAAUUAUUUGACUGUAGUAGCCAUCAGCAGAUGGAGAGUUCAGAGGGACUGCACUGAAAUAAUGAAUAAUUUGCAGAUGCAGUUGGUAGCCCUGGUGUCUUGGUGUGCCUUUCUGUUCCAGCAGGAUGCGUGCAAAGAGUGGCUCACAGCCCCAUCUGCUCUGCUCCUCCUGGCUCGAGCUUUGCUUUAAUAACCUCUCUGUCACCUAUUUACACGAGGUCAUCCAGCUCCUCUUUUUCUCCUUUUCUGUGUUGAAAUAAUCGUGGCUGCUACUUGCUGUGAAAGACUUAACUAGUAGUGGGUAGGAUUGACCUCUCAAUUCAGUAAACAUUUACUGAGUCCCCAGGACAAUGCUUGCAGUGAGCAUGCAGAGGAGGAGGUGAUUCCAGCCGGCAAGUGGAGGCAGAGCUCGAGCCAGCAGGCCUGGCCACUGCCUGGAAGUUGGGGGGUGAGGGGGGUGUGGAAGGUGAGCCAGGGUGCUUAGCCUCAGCCACUGGGGAAUGCGAAUGAUAGUCCUGGGGGAAAGAGAAAACAAGAGGAGGAACAGAUUUGUGGGAUGGAGAACAGUGGGGUAAUGAGCUCCAUUUGGGACAUUUUAAGUUUGAGACAGGACAUUCCCUGGAGACAUUAAGCAGGCAAUAAAAAGACCCCCAACUUAGAGUCCUCGAGGCCCUGCGGUUGCAGUGUGAAAUAAUCCGGCUUCAGCUUCCUUCCCUUUCCUUCUCAAGUGGUUCCCCAUGGAGUCACUUUAGACUCGGGGGGAGGAUAGUUGCUUCCUCAGUCUCCCUAGCCUUUAUCCUCACACUUGAAUGCUAAAUCCAGAACUCCUCAUUCCUGCUAAGUAGUUCAAAAGCUCCAAGGGAUCCUUGGAACAGUCGCACCCUGGUGGGACUUUUCAGAGCACUCCUAGGGUUAGAAGAGAAAUUUCAGGGUAACCGCAGAAUAAUGUGAGCUAUAACUGGCCCGAGUGAUCUUCUAGCUGGGACCUGGAUGUGAGGCUGGCAUGUUUGAAGGUUGGUGAAUGCCUGUUGACCUGCAUGCCCCAACCGGGUGAACUCCUUCUACCUUUUGAUUCCUAACUAAUUGCAGUGAACAAUACGCCAGCUUGUCUUCUGUAAAAUGAGAGGGUGACUGUGCCCACCAGCCUUGCUGCUUUGGUUGGACAGGUCAGUACAGUGCCUUGAAACUCUACUUAUUCAUCUGUGAAAUGAAGGGAUUUGGCGAGAUGCCGCUUAACGUGACUUCCAGCACUAGCAUUUUAUGUAGGUCAGUGAUCCUUUGUCCAGGGAGUGAUCUUUUUUCCAGAGGAACCGUUCUGCAGUUGCUGGUUAGCUUAUCAUCUUGGCAGGGAGCAGCGUGGUGAAGCGAGCAGAACGUGGCCUCCGGAGUCAGCAAACCUAGUUAAAAUCCACUUGCCGUAAGUCCGUCACGUGGCUUCGCAGCGGGCCUCUUGGCAAUUAGCUGCUUUUCACCAGUCCUCAAGUUUCCUCAUCUGUAAAAUGGGAUGAUGAUAUGUAUUUCAGGUCCGGUGGGUGAGAAUAUGUAUCAGGCAUCUACUUUUGUGACUAUUUUUAAAAUGGCUUUAUUGAGAUAUAACUCACAUACCGGAAAGUUCACUUUUUUGAAGUGUACAGCUCAUCAGCUUUUAGCCUGUUCACUAAGUUGUACAUCAGGCACCACUGUCCAAUUCCAGAACAUUCCAUCAUCCCAAAAGGAAAUCCCAUUCCUGUUAACUCACUCCCUAUUCGCUUCUCCUUCUAGCCCCUGGCAACCACUAAUCUAUUUUCUGUCUCUAUGGGUUUGCCUGUCCUGGACAUUUCAUUGAAAUGGAAUCAGACAAUGUGUGAUCUUUUGUGUCUGGCUUCUUUUGCUUAGCAUGAUGUUUUUGAGGUUCAUCCAUGUUGUAGCAGGUAUCGGUUCUUCAUUGCUUUGUAUUGCCAAAUAGUGUUUCACGGUAGGAAUAUACCACAUUUUGCUUAUCUGUUAAUCACUUGAUGGACAUGCAGGUGGUUUCCACUUUUUGGCUGUUAUGAAUAAUCCUCCUGUGAACAUUAGUGGACAUGGUUUUGUGUAGACAUAUGUUUUCAGUUUUCUUGGUAUCCCAUUGUGUUUUUGAUUUGCAUUUCCCUAAUAAUUAAUAAUGAUCAUCCUGUGCAUAUUGACCAUUUGUAUGUCUUCUCUGGCUAAAUGUAUAUUCAGUUCUUCAUUCAUUUAAAAAAUUAGGUUGUGUUUUUAUUAUUGAGUUGUAAGAGUUCUUUAUAUACUCUGGAUGUUGUACCUGGCUUUUAAAUAGGCAUACAAUCAAUGUUAGUUCCUCAUUCCAGGUCUCUCGCAGAACCCUGUAGUCUUUUAGGUGACCUCUGGAACUAACUGCCCAGACACUUAAUCCUCAGCAUCCUGAGUCUUAAACCAUCCCCUUAUGUCUUGUUCAGAGCUCUUCUUAGCACAAAGCCCUGAGCCAUUUUGAUCCUGGAGCCCCAGUCUGGAACUUGGAACAGCAGGGGGAUAGGUGGGGUCUAGAGAUGGGCUCUGGCUGAAUCCACAGGGCAGUGGCUACUACCAAGUCUCAUUUUUUUCUAGAUGGAGGACUUAGGGGGUAACUGCACUGAUUUUUGGCUGCAUGGAGUCCUCUGUCCUGUGCUAUGGACACCUGCAUGUUGGGGCUGGGGCCCACAAAGAGAUAUGUCUAAGGACACUGGCUUCUUUCCACUGCCACUGCCAAGAUGAGCAGCGGAUUUUCCAAGAGUGAUCUGGCAGUUGUAAGUUGUAUAUAAAAAUGUCCCAAGGAAAAUCAUGUGUCUGUUUUAAAGAGAAGGGAGUUUUCUAGGAAACCUUUGACCUGGACAUUCUUCUCUAUUCUGAGAACUGUACCCUGUGCCCCCAAGAUGUGAUCUGUACUUUGUUGCCCCUCUGCUUUUGUGCCCAUCAUCUUCUUCCUCUAUUUCUCCUCCCUGAUGUGUGCAGCCCUCCCUUUCAGCCAGUAGGGAAAGGGAAACCUGCAGGGUCCGGCAGGGUCCCCUGUUCCUCCCCAACAAAGCCUCUUAGGUUUUCUUUGGCUGGGGUCUCUUCCUGCACACCUGGGGAAGAGGUGCCUGCAAAGCAGUGAAGGCCUUGGGAGUCCCACCUAGACUGUCCUCCAGAGAGCCAUCUCCACUAGUUUGUGAAACUGCCAUGCCACGUUUCUGUCCUAAAGACUUGGCCUUUCCUUAGACAUGGAUUUGAUGGGUCCUGGACAGACGUUAUUGAUUGUUCCUCAUAAGUCAGUCAAGACAGUUUAUAGUCUCUGUUAAUGCCCGGGAAAUUUGUUUUGGAAGACAAAGCCAGCCCAAUGGCAUUUGGAUGAUGCUGACUUAUUUUAAAGGGGAGAAGAUACCCCUAGAUGUGCAAGUCUUUUAUAGGAACAGCUGUCUAUGAUGAGUCUUCAUGCUCCUUUUGCUUCUCUGAACAUUCUGGCAUGCCCCUACCUAGCUGCUAUUUUCUUGAUUUCAUAGAAAAGCACAUUCUACCCUCAGAAAAUCUGCUGUCCAUUUGGAAUGAUAAGAUAAAUCAGAAAAUUACCCAUUGUUAGAGCUAAAAGAUUCCUUGGGGAUUAUCCAAUCCAUUAUUUUUCAAUCUCCUAUCCUGACAAAAAAGAGUAAGUGUUUUGUAUGGAGAAAAAAAAAAGAAGUUUCCCUUUGGUAAAUAAAUUUGGGCUUCAGAGCAUAUUGUAUAUCCCUCUUGGAGAUCCACGGUGUGCACUGCGAUAUUAAAGCCUCUGAGAAGUCCUGCAAAAAAGAAAACCGCUUUAUUUGAUUUAACCCAGCAUUUCUUAAACUGUUUUGACCUCAUUUUUUUCUUCUUUUUUCAUAAUAAAUAUUAGCACCUCACAGGACACUCAGCCCAGUUUGGUAAGCAUGGCCUCCUUCAUGGAAGAAGAAAUCUGUGUUCAGAAAUAUUAAGUGACUUGCUCAAAAUCAACACAAAGCCAGACUUGAAGCCAAAUUUUCUAACUCCCACUCCAUUGUUCUUUCUACAAUUUAUAACCAUGUCGUGGCUGAGUCCUCUGAUUUUACGAGCUCAUGACCUUGGGGGAGCGAAUCCUGCCAGUCUCUCUGGAUCUCUUUCUUCUGUAAGGUGAGGAUGAUAAUAAUGACCUCCCAGGGUUGCCGUGAGGCUUAGAUGAGAGAGUGUAUGUAAAGAUCAAGUUCACGUUCUUAUCUUUGUUUUCUCUGACAUUUUUCAUCAUACCAGGUUCUGUGCCACUUAUCUAUGAUUUCAAAAGACGAACCAUAUUACAAACAACAAAACGUGAAUGGUGGUGAUCAUACUGAGUAUUUAUUGAAUAGUGACUGAGAAAAUGAAUGCACAGGAGACAGGAGGAGUUACCUGUGAAAAUUCAGAGCUAUACUGAACUGAUCAACGUUCACGGAAUUGGAGAAAUAACAAAGGUAUGGCCUCACAUGUGCAAGUUUUCUCCCCUCACACCCUUCAAUCAAGUGCCUUCUGUAGUGUGAAGAAACUGAAAAUAGAGCCGAGUUCCAACUGGGACAUGACUGGGUACGGCUCCCACAGCAAAGUGUAUAGCCAGAGCAAGAACAUCCCCCUGUCGCAGCCAGCCACCACAACCGUCAGCACCUCCUUGCCGGUCCCAAACCCAAGCCUACCUUACGAGCAGACCAUCGUCUUCCCAGGAAGCACCGGGCACAUCGUGGUCACCUCAGCAAGCAGCACUUCUGUCACCGGGCAAGUCCUCGGCGGACCACACAACCUAAUGCGUCGAAGCACUGUGAGCCUCCUUGAUACCUACCAAAAAUGUGGACUCAAGCGUAAGAGCGAGGAGAUCGAGAACACAAGCAGCGUGCAGAUCAUCGAGGAGCAUCCACCCAUGAUUCAGAAUAAUGCAAGCGGGGCCACUGUCGCCACUGCCACCACGUCUACUGCCACCUCCAAAAACAGCGGCUCCAACAGCGAGGGCGACUAUCAGCUGGUGCAGCAUGAGGUGCUGUGCUCCAUGACCAACACCUACGAGGUCUUAGAGUUCUUGGGCCGAGGGACGUUUGGGCAAGUGGUCAAGUGCUGGAAACGGGGCACCAAUGAGAUCGUAGCCAUCAAGAUCCUGAAGAACCACCCAUCCUAUGCCCGACAAGGUCAGAUUGAAGUGAGCAUCCUGGCCCGGUUGAGCACGGAGAGUGCCGAUGACUAUAACUUCGUCCGGGCCUACGAAUGCUUCCAGCACAAGAACCACACGUGCUUGGUCUUCGAGAUGUUGGAGCAGAACCUCUAUGACUUUCUGAAGCAAAACAAGUUUAGCCCCUUGCCCCUCAAAUACAUUCGCCCAGUUCUCCAGCAGGUAGCCACAGCCCUGAUGAAACUCAAAAGCCUAGGUCUUAUCCACGCUGACCUCAAACCAGAAAACAUCAUGCUGGUGGAUCCAUCUAGACAACCAUACAGAGUCAAGGUCAUCGACUUUGGUUCAGCCAGCCACGUCUCCAAGGCUGUGUGCUCCACCUACUUGCAGUCCAGAUAUUACAGGGCCCCUGAGAUCAUCCUUGGUUUACCAUUUUGUGAGGCAAUUGACAUGUGGUCCCUGGGCUGUGUUAUUGCAGAAUUGUUCCUGGGUUGGCCGUUAUAUCCAGGAGCUUCGGAGUAUGAUCAGAUUCGGUAUAUUUCACAAACACAGGGUUUGCCUGCUGAAUAUUUAUUAAGCGCCGGGACAAAGACAACUAGGUUUUUCAACCGUGACACGGACUCACCAUAUCCUUUGUGGAGACUGAAGACACCAGAUGACCAUGAAGCAGAGACAGGGAUUAAGUCAAAAGAAGCAAGAAAGUACAUUUUCAACUGUUUAGAUGAUAUGGCCCAGGUGAACAUGACGACAGAUUUGGAAGGGAGCGACAUGUUGGUAGAAAAGGCUGACCGGCGGGAGUUCAUUGACCUGUUGAAGAAGAUGCUGACCAUUGAUGCUGACAAGAGAAUCACUCCAAUCGAAACCCUGAACCAUCCCUUUGUCACCAUGACACACUUACUCGAUUUUCCCCACAGCACACACGUCAAAUCAUGUUUCCAGAACAUGGAGAUCUGCAAGCGUCGGGUGAAUAUGUAUGACACGGUGAACCAGAGCAAAACCCCUUUCAUCACGCACGUGGCCCCCAGCACGUCCACCAACCUGACCAUGACCUUUAACAACCAGCUGACCACUGUCCACAACCAGGCUCCCUCCUCUACCAGUGCCACUAUUUCCUUAGCCAAUCCCGAAGUCUCCAUACUAAACUACCCAUCUACACUCUACCAGCCCUCAGCGGCAUCCAUGGCUGCAGUGGCCCAGCGGAGCAUGCCCCUGCAGACAGGAACAGCCCAGAUUUGUGCCCGGCCUGACCCGUUCCAGCAAGCUCUCAUCGUGUGUCCCCCCGGCUUCCAAGGCUUGCAGGCCUCUCCCUCUAAGCACGCUGGCUACUCGGUGCGAAUGGAAAAUGCAGUUCCCAUCGUCACUCAAGCCCCAGGAGCUCAGCCUCUUCAGAUCCAACCAGGUCUGCUUGCCCAGCAGGCUUGGCCAAGUGGGACCCAGCAGAUCCUGCUUCCCCCAGCAUGGCAGCAACUGACUGGAGUGGCCACCCACACAUCAGUGCAGCAUGCCACCGUGAUUCCCGAGACCAUGGCAGGCACCCAGCAGCUGGCGGACUGGAGAAAUACGCAUGCUCACGGAAGCCAUUAUAAUCCCAUCAUGCAGCAGCCUGCACUAUUGACCGGUCAUGUGACCCUUCCAGCAGCACAGCCCUUAAAUGUGGGUGUGGCCCACGUGAUGCGGCAGCAGCCAACCAGCACCACCUCCUCCCGGAAGAGUAAGCAGCACCAGUCAUCUGUGAGAAAUGUCUCCACCUGUGAGGUGUCCUCCUCUCAGGCCAUCAGCUCCCCACAGCGAUCCAAGCGUGUCAAGGAGAACACACCUCCCCGCUGUGCCAUGGUGCACAGUAGCCCGGCCUGCAGCACCUCGGUCACCUGUGGGUGGGGCGACGUGGCCUCCAGCACCACCCGGGAACGGCAGCGGCAGACAAUUGUCAUUCCCGACACUCCCAGCCCCACGGUCAGCGUCAUCACCAUCAGCAGUGACACGGACGAGGAGGAGGAACAGAAACACGCCCCCACCAGCACUGUCUCCAAGCAAAGAAAAAACGUCAUCAGCUGUGUCACAGUCCACGACUCCCCCUACUCCGACUCCUCCAGCAACACCAGCCCCUACUCCGUGCAGCAGCGUGCUGGGCACAACAAUGCCAAUGCCUUUGACACCAAGGGGAGCCUGGAGAAUCACUGCACGGGGAACCCCCGAACCAUCAUCGUGCCACCCCUGAAAACCCAGGCCAGCGAAGUAUUGGUGGAGUGUGAUAGCCUGGUGCCAGUCAACACCAGUCACCACUCGUCCUCCUACAAGUCCAAGUCCUCCAGCAACGUGACCUCCACCAGCGGUCACUCUUCAGGGAGCUCAUCUGGAGCCAUCACCUACCGGCAGCAGCGGCCGGGCCCCCACUUCCAGCAGCAGCAGCCACUCAAUCUCAGCCAGGCUCAGCAGCACAUCACCACGGACCGCACUGGGAGCCACCGAAGGCAGCAGGCCUACAUCACUCCCACCAUGGCCCAGGCUCCGUACUCCUUCCCGCACAACAGCCCCAGCCACGGCACUGUGCACCCGCAUCUGGCUGCAGCCGCUGCCGCUGCCCACCUCCCCACCCAGCCCCACCUCUACACCUACACUGCGCCGGCGGCCCUGGGCUCCACCGGCACCGUGGCCCACCUGGUGGCCUCGCAAGGCUCUGCGCGCCACACCGUGCAGCACACUGCCUACCCAGCCAGCAUCGUCCACCAGGUCCCCGUGAGCAUGGGCCCCCGGGUCCUGCCCUCGCCCACCAUCCACCCGAGUCAGUAUCCAGCCCAAUUUGCCCACCAGACCUACAUCAGCGCCUCGCCAGCCUCCACCGUCUACACUGGAUACCCACUGAGCCCCGCCAAGGUCAACCAGUACCCUUACAUAUAAACACUGGAGGGGAGGGAGGGAGGGAGGGAGGGAGAGAAUGGCCCGAGGGAGGAGGGAGAGAAGGAGGGAGGCGCUCCUGGGACCGUGGGCGCUGGCCUUUUAUACUGAAGAUGCCGCACACAAACAAUGCAAACGGGGCAGGGGCGGGGGGGGGGGGGGGGGCAGAGGGCAGGGGGACGGGUCGGGACACCAGUGAAACUUGAACCGGGAAGUGGGAGGACGUAGAGCAGAGAAGAGAACAUUUUUAAAAGGAAGGGAUUAAAGAGGGUGGGAAAUCUAUGGUUUUUAUUUUAAAAAAGAAAAAGGAAAAAAAAAAAGUCAAUAACAAAAAACCCAGCUCAAGAACCCAUUCUACGCCAAACUGGAAAGGAGAAGAGAGCAACAGGAAGAUUCCAGAAACGGGGGGCCCCAGUUUUUGAAGAACUUUAUGAACUUUUCAAAGAUUAUUUUCAUAUGGCAGCAAGUGAUACGGAAGACUGCUGUCAGGGACACCUGAUAUGGAAAUCAAAUAGAUUUUUAAUUAAUUGAACAUAAGAUUUAGGGAUUUUUCCAGAACUCGAAAGGGUCAACAGCCCUCCAGAAUGUCGGGCUGCAGCCUGAGGAGGCUGAUGUUUGGAGCUGGUGUGGGAUUGGCGAAGCCCAGUCCGGGCUCCCUAGUCAGGAAAGACGGGGGACGGCCAGGCUGCUGGAAGGCCCCCGGGGGCGCGGGGCGAGUUUUCUUUUUCUGAGCACUCUGGAUAAAUCCCUAAGCAACGUUGUUUCUCAAAUGUCAUUAAUAAUGUGUGUUGCAAACUUUAGGUUUUUUUCUUUUCUGAAAAUGUAUUUUCUCUUUGAAUCCACCCCUAGUCGCGUAGCGUAGGGCUAGCGGUCGUCACAGACACCCUAGUAGAAUGUAGCACUCAGCACCCUUGUCUCCUACCUUGUGUUCAACUCCAAUGAUACCAAUAGAAUAUUCCUCAAUGUAAUUGCACAAAAAAAAGCGAUAUAACAUAGGCAUGUAACCAAUGUGGCGGUGCAGGUGUGCGGGUGAGCGAGCACGUGUGGGUGUGCACGCGCCGCCCUCCCCGCGUGGCCCUCGGCGCCGCCACCCUAGCUGGCGCAGUCUUGACACUGCAUCCUUCCCUCCUAGUGCCUUACCGAGCGACAGACGCGGCGUGAGGGUUUACUUCCACUGGUACUCCAAGAAACUGAGGCUAGUCAGACACAAUCUCAGCUCUUCUGUUGUGCUGUUGUAACAGUUUACGCUGGCCUUUUUUUUUUCUUUUUCUUUUUCUUUUUAAAAUGUUAAUGCCCGUUGUCUUUCCUGGGCUGUUUGCUAGCGGAAGGAUGCCAGGGAAGCCAGCAGGAGCUAGGAGAGAGUCCGUGGAUCUCGAAAGAAAUAUGGGAGACAGAUGCCCGGCGGGUGCGUCUGGAGAUGGGGACGGCGGGAGUUGAGUUGUGGCAGUAGUUGAGUUGUAAUUUGUGGGCGGAGGCCCAGAGAGACUCCCCACCCUUCACCCCUGCCCCACUCUGUCCCCAGUUCCGCCAUUUGUGAGGCCAGAGGUUUCCGGACUGUUGGCCUCGCCAGGCAGCCGUCUCCCGCCCCAGGCGGCAUCCCCCAGUCCCUCCCGCCUCCACGAGAGCCUGGAGCUCUCAGCCUCGCCCGGGGCUCCACUCUCUCCUCCGGCUCCCUGGGCUGUUUUGCUCUAACGAUCUUGCCAGAUCCCUCCCUCUGUAGACAACCACCAACCUCUGUUUGCUGUUGAAUUCUCUCCUCACAUUACCCAGGUCUGCUCAAGACAUGAUUUUGGUUUUGGUUUCUGAGGGUUCUAGUGGGCAGAAGGUUGGAGGGACACUUAUGAGGGUGGCCGGGGGUCUGACGCUGCACUUUGGAAAAACUCACACAGUUGAAUUUCCAAAGAAAUCUGCCCUUUGCCCUCUUUGCACCUUUGAUACAUUCUGGAAGUUUUCUCAGGCUUUGGACACUUCUGGGGAUGGAGGUGUGGAGAAGUGGGGAGUUCCCUCUCUUCAUAGUAAAUAACUCUGAAAUAUGUGAAUGUGAAUGGCAGGAGAAUCUGGCCAAGGAUGGGGCCGAAAAGGGUGGUUCUAAUUGUUUGCUUCUGAUGUUGAGUCUUUAGCUGACCCCACAGGCAGGUUUCCAAGGUGCAAAGAGAUCUUUCCCGAGUCAGCGGCCCCAUCCUCAUCCUCCCUCCCUUUACUUCCUCACUGUGCAGUCUCCCUCAAGGAUCUACUGUGAAAGGUGUGUUUGUAGUGAUAUCCAACCUAACUCAGUAACGAAGUCGUUACUUAGCUCUUAGCUGUGAAAUAACUCUGGAAACUUCCCCACCCCAACCAUAAAUUCUUACUUAUAAAGAAACAGGUCCCCAAACUGGAAACAGCUUAGUCCAGGCCUCAGCGAGAAGGAAGGACACCAUGACUGCUCCAUGCUGGGCACAGCCGGGCAGUCUUGCCAAGUGCCUGCUGGAGGCUGUGCCGGCAAGAGGCCUGCAGCAAGGAGAUUCCCUUCCCUCGGGCCAUUAUCAAUACUGUCUUUAUCUGGAGGUGGGGAAGCGCAGCCCUCUGAGACAGCAGGACAAUGGUCAGUUCAGAGAGGGUGAGGGCAGCAAACGCUUCAGAGGACACAGAAGCCAGAGGACCCCCCCCCGCCCCACAGCUGGGUCAGCCUGGAAAAUCCAUCUAUUAGGGACUUUUUGGCAGCCAGAUGGCAGCAAUAGCCCAUUAGGUCUCAUCCCGAGUUCCAAGUCUUGGCUGCAAAUGAGCCUCAGUUCGCCUUACUGGAGAGCACCCCCAGAUUCCUGGGCACAGUUCAUUUCCAGCCCUUUCUAGAUCUGAUCUUUUAGGGGGAAAGACAGCUUAAAAUGUUCUUUUCAUUUUAAAGAAAAUUAUUCUGUCUGCUUAAGUUGGAGGCUACUUACUCUUUCACCUGACAUUUUCUUUCCUUUUAUUCUUCCAGAUCAGGAAUGAAAUUUCCAUGCUGCUCAUAAAGAUAAUAUUAUUGUACUAAUUAUUUUUAUUACCAUUGUAAUUAUGAUCAUUAUGUUGAUAUUUUAGUCAGGGUUUUAAAUGCACAUUUAUUCCAAGUAUCUUUGUGUUUUCUCUUUAAUAUUUAAACUUAUUCUCUCUGUGAGUAUAUAAGUAGACUGGAGGGACAUCCAGAUGUCCAGUUUUGUCAGGCAAAAAAAAAAAGGAAAGACUUAGGAAGUAGGAAAAUUGUUUCUGUCAUCUCUAUCCCAACAAGAGACGUCAAGAAAGAUCCACCACAGAACAAAAGUUUAAAGAAGAAUCAAAGCCUUGAUUGGGCUUCUGACAACAUGGUCACCAUCAAGGUUGUCAUUUUCUAGAUCCCAGAGGCCUGGGAUGCGACGUCAGGUGGCAUCUCAUGGGCUCGGGGAAUGUCGAGUCACUGACUGUCCAGCCCUUAGCCAGCUUCUCUCCCACAUCCUCAGAGCUCUCCUGUGCUUCUGAAAUCUGUUAACUAAAUCUUUGGCUUGCCUCUGGUAUUUAAGCAAGAAAAUUCCCUCCCAGAGGUGACCCCAUCCGCUUCCCCACAAUCCAUCCUUUUGCCAUCGGCGCACCUGGGGCGUGGCUUAGGUUCUUCAAUGCAGGGACAUUUGCCCCCUCCCAGAAGCUGCUGGGCACAGUGAGGUGGCGUAAGAGUGACUGGCAGGUGGUACCUUCCCCAGGAAAUUUCACCACACCACCCAGUUCCUCAGCCUGCCCCCUCCCCCUGUGAUGCAUGCCCCCAGCACCCAAUUCUAGCCAGCUGGAAGUGGGUGGAGGGACAGCAGGAGGCCAGAGAAACCCUGAACAAAGCUGGGCGGCUGCUCAGGCAUCACAGGCUGCACCCCCUCUGAAAGCAUCCCCACUGGGCUCCGGCCACAUCUUCAGUGCACUGUGCUGUGUGCGCUGGGUGCUCACACGCUGUCCCCAGACCCACAAAGUGCUAGGCCCCAGUUGAAGAAAGGGGUGAAAUAGCCAGCUUCACCGAAGGGAAGGGAAGGGAAGUAUUGGGCGAUGCCAGCCCCACAGACGCUCAGCAAACAUUAGUGCACAUUCUCCUAGUCCUCACCCAAUGGCCUCCUCUACCCCCAUGCAUGGAGCUGCCACAUCAGAAGCCCCAAGAGAAGCUCCCUGCAGGAGAGGCCAGCUCCCUGGAUGCCCAAUUGCAUACCUGGCCGAAUCUGCCAUUGAGUCACCUUAGCAAAUAGGCUGCUGUCACUAGGACCAAGCUCUCAAGCAGAGGGAUGCCAACCUAGUCCUUACUUAGCCCACGAAUCAUCUAGAGCAUCCUCUAGUCUUUUGUGGGCUCCCUCCUUCCCAUUUGAAGAGACAUUGUUCAGAGGAAGAGGGGAAGAUUUGAAAUGUCAGGUCACGGAGGAGUGUUUAACUGGAGCCUGGUGAACCGCAGGGCAAUUUGCUUCUGCUCACUGGGUUCUGACUGGCCCGUCUGGACGUGGGCCCCCAUGUCUCUGUGCUUAGGGCCUCUUCAUGAUGUUUUGGAUGUUUCCAAGGGAAGUGGGUGAGCAGAUCAAGGGGUGGGAGAGUCGAGGCUUGAUGCCAGUUAAUACUGUGAAGUGGAGCGUGCGGUCAGUGGAAUUCAGAGGAAAAAGAAGGGUUGGAGCAAAGCGGCAUUCAUCUCCUGGACUGUUAGCCUUUCUAGUCUUCCUGGUGGCUGAGGUGUUCACGGGCUGGGGGAGCCAGCUGACCUUUGUCCUCUUCAACCUAGAAGACUCAGCCCGCCCAGACACCAACGUGUGAGACGGAUGGACAUCAGGAAGGGAAGGGGAGAUUAGCCCAACUGCUGACAGAACGAUUUCCCUUGGUUGGACCUUGGGAAUGGCAAACACUCAUAUUGGAACAAGCUUGGGGUGGAAGAUUUAGGCCGUGUGAGCAUGUGUGAGUGAGUGGAACAAACUUUCUUGGAAACUGGAGGGAGGAGAUGAGGAGGCUUCGGGAAGUAUUACUGAUGGCUCAUGGUUGAGAGAGCGACGUGGGGACCCAGCUCGCCCCAGCUUUUGUCCCAGGUUCUCUUUGUCUGAUGCUGAGGGCAGGGUGGGGUGUGGGACCACCACUCUUGUUGGCCUGUCAAGUAGACCCUAGGACAGAAAAUGGAAAGAAGGAAAUGGCUCGGUGCUCUCAACUAGCAGAGAGAAUUGAGGAGAGGUAAGGGUUCCUUCUGCAGGCCAGCCUGGGACUCCACAGCGCCAGCAGGAGUGACUUGGCCACAAGACAUUCCAGCCCCAGGGACUUUGCAGGCUUCAUUCCCUGUCUGUGUCUUUUCCUUCUGGUGUGUUUUACAGACUUCUGAUGGGGAAGCUUCAAACUUGAGCAGGCCAGAGAUGUCCUUACCAAAUUGGAAAGGAAGGUGAAACUGUUCCUUUCUUUAGCCAAAGAACCCUUCUCAAAGACGCCUCCAGAAAUGGACAAAAUGGCCUUCCCUUCGUUCCUUUCCAGGCAAUAAUGACAUCAUUAGUGAUGCAAUUCUAUUUGUCUUUCUCUUUCCUCUCUGUCCUUUUUUUUAAAAAAAAAAAAUGCAUUUAUUUCAAAACUGUGCUAUUCUUUUAAGAGGAGUGGAGGUGACCCCUUCGAUGCUGCUGCUAUCGGGAGACAAGGUGCCAUACCAAUACGUGGGCUUGACUAAUCCCAGGCCACCAUGGGAGAGAGCAAAGCAGGGCUGCCAGGAGUUCAGUUGCAUCAAGGGCGUAGAGCACGCGGGGGCUGGGCUCGGAAUAGCAGUACUUUUCCACUUUGAUGCCUUAGAACUCUCACUUCUCAUCUCCACAGACCAGACUCAGUAAAAUCUCAGGCCACUAGAGAAUGGAAGGCGGUGAAACAGGAUUUAAAUGCAAAAAAAACCUAUUGGAGGCUUUUGGCACCGUGGCUCACUAGAGGGACCCAGCAUAGUAGAGGUUUCUCUUGUUGCAGCUUCUGAAAAGUUCAAAAAAGAACUCCAGGCCGUUCUUCCCUCAAACCCAGUGAGAGUUUGCAGAGAAGUGCCCCCUGCAGGGCUCCCGUCCCAGAACACCAGCACCAGAGAGGGUCUUCCCGAUGCCCCCCGCUGGACUUGCCCAAGCCUCUGGGAGCCCCUCAUCUCAGAUCCCUGUGUUGAACAUGACACUGACUGUCCCUUAUUUGUUAAAAUUUGCAAUAUCUCUCAAGUAAAUAAUAGCCAACAUUUGUUGAAUGCUUUCAUGACUCCCGGGCUAAGGCCUUUAUGAGCGUUGUCUCAAGGGGCCCCAACAGCCAUCCCACAGGGAGGGGGAUAACAGCCCCCAUUUAUAGAUAAGGGAGCUGACCGGAUGCUCUGAGAAGUGGCAGGUGUUGAAGGAAGGAUAAAGCAGUGAUGGGCCAGAAUCCCCAAGGUUCCCUUUUUUGUUCAUCAGGCCCUUCCUGAGAUGUGAUUUUUAAUCUUUUAACUUUUUUUAAUUAAUAGCAAUGCGUGGCCUCAUAUUUCUAUGAACCAUUUAGUGAUACUCCCGCUUCCUGCAUGCCACACACUGUGCUGGGAAUUGCUCAUGGGUUGUCCUGUUUCAUCUUCUCCGUAGCCCUGUGAGAUCGGCAAUAUUAGUCCCCCUACAGCCAAGGAAACUGCCCAGAGCCACACAACUCUUGAGGGGCGAGGAGGGCUUGAACCUGAGUCUGCCCAGCUCCAGAACUGAGCUUGCAGCCAUUAGCCACAGCUGUCUCCUGCAUGUCUGAGCAAAGAAAGGCCUUUACACAGCAUCACCCUGUGCCAUCCCAUGCACCGUGGGACUCAGCUAAAGGACUGUGCAAAGAGGGGGCUCCUGAGUUGGAUUUAGGCAAAAGGGGCAGAAUUCGUUUGAUUUUUAGAGAAAAUCUCUGGAGAGUUUCUUUUGAUUCAUAGAAUUCCUUUUAGAUUUCUUUCCAGCAUACCAACUAGCUUUAGUAGUGCUGCUACAACCAGCUCUUAUAAGUAAGAGUGAAAAAGUAUUCUUUUCUUCUUUAAAAAAUAAGUUUUUCUUGCUUAUAGUUAAUUCUAGAAAGGCAAUACUAAAGGUAUAUAUUUUUUUCAAAAUGCUAUUUUUUACUGCACUUGAUAAUUAUCCUGACAGCUCUGAUCUCUGUAAUAGAUUCACUCUUCAGCUCUGGGCAGAACCAGAGGCAGGGUUCACACCAAAUUUGUAAAUACCAUAUGUGGGUCUGGUGUCCAGGAACUUUUUUCUUUCUGUUAAAAAAAAGAAAAAAAAAAGAAAAAAAAAAAGAAGUAGAGGUGGAAGAAAGACAAGACUUAGAGGAACAAAAGAAUGUUUUCUUUUGAGAUACUCUUCUCAAAGAAAUAGCAACAAUUGUAUAAACAGGAAAACCAGCCAGCUUUCAUGAUAAAAGGAAGGCGUGUCUCUUGCCCUGGUAUGAGAUUAACAGAAAUACAGAUGCAUUUUUAUUUUGAUUGAAAGAUGGUGAGAAUGUAGAAAUGCUUAGGACUAGAUUUUUAAUUUUUUAAAAUAACUAUUAUCAUUUAUUAUGAAAUAUUUGUUCAGUUGUUUUGAGUGGGUUUCUUGUUCCUUUUUUCAUUUAAAACCUUCUUUGUUGACUGGCUCCAGGCUUGUUUGCCUAAAUUCUUAGGUAGUUUACACAAGUUCUAGAAUCUUUUAGAACUUUAACUCCAUUGGAAGCAAACCUAACUAAUCGGAGUUUGAGAUCCUGGUUGGUUUCAAUAGGUAUUCUGGAAUUCUGGCAGAACACCUAAAGAUUUUUUUUUUUUUUAGAAGGUUUUAGAUACAUUAUCUUACACAAACUGUGACCUAAUGGCAAUAAUUACCUCAAAUGUGGGCAUUCAUCCUGGUUUUAGCCUUUUUUGAAAUCAUGUAGCCAGCUUGAUCUUGGAAUUUAAAGACUAUGAAUUCUCUGUGGGCUGAAAAUAAUGAUUACUUCAUACCCCCGGUCAUCGUUGCUUAAGUGAAUUCUGAAAAUAGCUCAUCUUUACAACAAAAAUUAAACCAAGGAAGAGAUUAUUCUUUGUGUGUUGUACUCAAAUGCGAUGUUCAAAUGCACAUGUUAAGUAUAUAUGUUUUUAGCUACUGUAAAAUGCUGUUAGCCUUCUAAGCUAUCAAAACAGUCACAUUUUAAAUGAGUAAACUAAACAAUUGACUGUGGAUACUUAAGCAUAUUUCUGGCUACGUUUUAUAGUUAAAGUGUUUUAUAGUUUACAUUUAGACUGGUACUUUUUAAAGAAAAGUUCUGUUUAUAACUGACAUCCGCAAACCCCAGUGAAUGCCUCUUAGUUGGAGGUUGUGUCUCCCCCAAGGCAAGUGUGUUGUCCCAGACUCUUCUGUAGUCCAGCAUGCGCACUUCCCUCUGGAUUAUUACUUUCCACGUGAACUCAAGAGAACAUGAAAGGCAAUCCAGAUGGAGGGAAAAGGUGUGAGUCCGCAGCCCGGGCCAGAUGCGAAGGUCUCAUGCGUGUCGUCUAAACACUUGUCUUCAAGGCCUUCUCUCUGACAUCUUGGAAGAGUCAUUGAGAACAGAUAACCUGGUUCAUUGAUUUUUGUCUUGAUUUGAAUAUUUAACUUAUUAAUAGAUCCACUGAUUUCCAGGCACCAGGCAGUAGAAGAGACUGGGAUUCAGGUGACCAUGAAGGCACAGCUGCUACUUCUGGGCCGGGGGUGAUAUUUUGAUCAGCGUUUUGUAGGGGAGGACCAUAUACCCCUAUUCCCAUGGUCGCUGGCUGGGUUUUCCAUAUAUCUGCUGUCAUUUAUUCGUUUUCCCCUUAAAAGCAAAAUCAAUGUAAAAGGCUAUGUUUACGUUUUACUCAUUGUCCAGCUUAGACUCAAAGUCUAGUUCGGUGGGAGGGGGACCUUAGCAUCCUCUCAGAGAUGGUCAGGGCUGAGCAGGAGGAGGCAGAGACAGAGGGGCAGCUCAGCCUGGUCCAUUGAGACCCACUCUAAACAGACAUCAUAUUUGGAACAAGAAGAUGCUUCGAGACAGGAAUGGGCCCCACUGUCAUGCAGAAACAGACUGGGGGAAUGGCAGUUUCCCUGAGUCUUGGUUUCUUUUAUGUUUUCUCUUGUGCCACCACCAAACUGCAGAGGACCUGCUGUGACCUAAAGGGCAUUCCUUUAGCAGAUAAGACCUUGAAAACUGCAAAACACCUGGGACCAGGGAGCUUUUAAAAAAUACAAAAAAAUACCACAUUUGCUUUUUCCCUGUGAACUGUAUUGACAGCGUGUUCUUAGGACAGUCUUUUGGUGGAAAUGUUACUGUAAAAUAGUUUUCAUCUCACCCCUCCUAAUCAUACUCCCACUUUCCUGUUUGUGUGGUGGUGUUGCUGUUUUUUCCUUUACAUGAAUUAACCAAAUGAAUUUUGUGUCAUUGUUUUUGGGGCUUAUAUUUUUAAAACAUAGAAAUUGCCUUUUGUUCAUUUGAAAAGUAAGUAUGUUGUAUCUGAAAAAGGGCUCUGCCUCUGCUCUCCCUCGCUUCCUUGUAACCAAUCUCCAAACGAAUCUCUCCUGGCACCGCCCCCUUCCUUAUAUAGGGUCACUGUCCCCGGGGCCACCUCUGCCUCCACCCUGCUGUCACCACUGCCCUGGGCCAAGGCACCCAGGACUCCCAGAAAGCGCGAGAGCCAGCAAGAAGGCCCCACUCAGCCUUGAGACUGGUGGUCACACCUCCCUGUCAGAGUCGCCUGCUGGGCUGAAGGGGCAAUGGAUUGUCAUUGUUGAAAUUGUUUGGCUCAGGUUAUAAGGAGGAACUUGGGAAGUAGAAAGUGACUUGACCAUGUGCAUCCUUGGUAGCUUCCUGUAACUAACAAAUGGAACAGAGAGCACACCCCCGCCCCGCCCCACCCCAAGCAGAUGUUCCCGUCAGCGCUGCCCUGAGUCAGUCGGUCCCCCGUUUCUGCUCUCCUCCCUUUUGUGUUCCUGCUCACUUCAAGCUUCUUCCAUGGACUUUCCAGGGCACAGUCAUCUCUAGCCCCCAAAUCAUCUCUUCAUCCUCUGUGUGUGCAUUUUUUUAACCAAAUGAAAUAGACAAGAAAGUCAUACUUUGGGGCAGCAGAAUUUCUAAUUUAGUAGAAUCACUGUAUAGAGAUAGAUGUUGAUAUAUAUGUUUGUGUAUAUAUAUCAAACCAAAUUGGAUAGGAGAAGUAUAGCUUUACAGAUGAGGAGAAGGAGCUCUUUAGAGGUCGGAGUCAAGACUGGUGUCUUGGACGUGCAUGGGCUGUGUCCCAGGCCACUCCGCACACAUGGGGCUGAGGCGUGGCGCCGGGCCCUUGUCAUCCACCUCACCACGGCAGAGCCAGCAGGCCCUGUAGGGUGCUGCUGCUGUCUCACUGGGUCCCAGCUUCAAGCGCAUCAGUGGGUGACGGGGGCAACAAAUCAGAGUGACUGGAAGUUUCCAUCCCGUUUUGCUUUGACCACGUGUACUGAGCUGCAGCCUCUGAUACUCUGUCACGUUUCCAAAAAUGGUAUCCAUUAGGAUAGAAAGAGAAUGGAUCUGCAGAAAUGUUUACCUUUCAACUGCUCAUGAAUUCAGGACACUGGAUAGAAAGACUCACUCCCCAAAAUGAGAACAGGGAAGAGGAGACCCGGCGACACUAAGUCACCAGGUCCAAGGAACGUGGCUCCCUCCCCAGGGUCAUCUCACCUAGAUCUUUCUCUCCCAGGUCAUCUCAGCUCAAUCUCAAUAACCCUAUGAAAGCCCUGGUCUGUUGUGUUCCUUCACCGUACGGUUUCUGUAAUAAAAAGUGUUAAUCCAUGUUAAUCUGUGUGAAAAUUAUUGCGUGCAACAGUAUUUUCUCGUGUACCUCUUUUUCCUAUGUGAAUUGUCCCUCUUUUUUAUUUAUAAAUGUCUACUUUUGUUUUUUUAAAGACAAACCAAUGUGUUGUAGACCUAUAUGUAACCUAUUCCUUAGUCUCAUAUUAUAGGUAUGUUAUAAGAAUGGAUAUUUUACUUGGCUUUAGAAUGUUUUACAAGAAAACUAAUUCUUAACUGAUCAAGUCCUUGCUACUAAAAUGCUUGUGUUUUUCAUCAUGACGUCGUGUGCUUCUAAAUUAAUCAUUUUCGUUGUAGAAAAAUGGAGUGAAUUUAUAUUAGUCUUGGAAACUAAUAAUAGCAUUGUAAAUUUAUGAGAUGAUUUUAACAGAAAAAAUAUAGAAGAAUAUAGUUAUUUUAAUUGUAAUAUUACUAACUGUAGGGUGAGAAAAAGGGGGGGGGGUCCCAUUGUGGUGAACUAUGUUAUAGCUUGUUACUCAUAGUUUCUUUUUGAUCAUUUUUUCGGUCUCCGAGGUGAAAUGACUUAUUAAUUAAAAUUUGUAAACUCACAUAUGCAUAUUGUAUAUGUGUAGAAAUGUAAUCACACUUUGUCUUGGAAUUACAUUAAACUGUUUGAAAUCACUGUA